AAGUUAGGCACAACAUCUGACUUGGAUUUCUCUCUGUUUUUUUCUCUUCCAGUUGUCUGUCUGUGCGCCCUCUCCCACAAGGAAUAGUUUUCCACACUGAUGGAAUUAAUGCAUAUCGUGGUAUUAUUGGUGGAAUAUGUUUAACCUUUGUUUCGUGAUUUGAGAGGAAUGGUUCUUGUGUAUCGUGUGGUGACAGCAGGUUAAGGAGAGUGUCAGAGCUGGUGCAGAGUUUUGCCCCGGGGCCAUGAGGUUCUGGGCAUCAUGACUCUCUUAUGAAGUUACAAAACUGGGCAAGUGAUUGAAGGCAGAAAGACACUGUAAUAAAGUGUGCUCCAGUGAUGUGUGCUCCGGCUUCUCUCCCUUACUCAUCUGGGCCAGGUGCUUUCGCCACAGUGAGCCUGGGUGUCCCCUGCCUGAGAUGAGCACAGUGAUGUCUAUGCGAGGUUGUAGGACUCAGUGAAGUGCCUUAGGGAUUUUGCCUGGCACUCUCCUGGGCUCAUGAGGUGCCUAGGGCUGAGACUUCCCCUUCUCUGUCUGGUAAAUCAUCUCUCCCAUUCUUUCUUCUGCGGCCCUUCAUAUGAGCUUUGUAAUUUACUCAGGGUGGCAGGGUGAAUUCAUCUUUUGCUGGGUUUCUGCAUCACCUGCUCCUUUCUGGCCAGGUCAGCCUGUUCAUUUUUUCCAUGCCAACAGCCUCUAAGUGCCAGUAAGUCACGUCUGAACAACCAAAGCAUGUUUCCCUGCGGGAGAAUGCCAGGGCAGGCGGGUCUGGGAGCCAAGAGGAUUUCUCCUGUUCAGAUAAGUCGGGGGAAUAGAAGAGCCCUGUGACUUGAGACAAGCUUUGAGUGACACCCAGUGAAUCUCCCAUCACUACUUUAAUCCCUGCCCCAGUGUUCUGGUUCCCCCUUUCCUGCAUGAGGCAGUACGAGUACCCUGGCCUGGCUUUGGGUUCUACACGGUCUGACUUUAGCCUGCCUUGGUCUUUGUUCCCCUCUCACUCCCUCCACCCCUGCCCCCCCCAACACAUGUGGAGUACCUUACCCUGCCUUCCUAGUUCUGGAAUGGCUGCCCCUGUGCCAGGCCACCCCAUUUUCUAGAACCACCUUCAUACAGCCCCUGCGCAUCCCACUGUACUAUUUCCUUGUUUGUUUUUCCUGUCAAUCUUGCCUUCCGCGCUAAUGGGACACUGAUGCUGUAUGGUGAUGUGUUCUCCCACAGUCAUCUUUUCCUCCUGUGGUUGGGGUGGGGAGCUUUCUCUGUGUCCCCCCAUGAGAGUGAGGACAGUCUCAUUUAAUGGCACCAUGGUCUGUGGAGCCAGGCAGGCCUGUGUGUCUGACUCCACUUCAGCGCUCUCAGCCAGCGUGGGCACCUCGGACCCAGACAGACGCCCCGAGCCUGUCUUUCUGGAGAAGGAAGUAGUAAUACCUUUUCCUUGAGGGAGUUAUGAGGAUUAACUGUGCCUGGCCCUGAAUUCGUGCCUUGCAGGUACUUAGGAAGUGAGUUAUUACAAGCAGUGCUUUUUAUCAUCCAUAGAUGGAGAUGUUAUCUAUGCUAUAGGACUGCAGAAAGAAUUACAGAGAAUUAUGUAGAAUCACUAGGGACUUGAUUAAUAUUUGUUUACCUUUCCCCCACAUGGAUUGAUGUCCUUUAUUAUACUUUUGUACCCCCGCUUGGCAAGCCCUUGACAAAUAUUGAUCCAACAAAAAAUUAGCUCUUUAAUGUAUACGUUUAGAACCUGUUGCUUUGUCAGUAGUGGUUUUUAUGAAAAUGAAUGCUUAUAGGUCAGACUUCUGGAAACCCUAAUCUGAGGGAAUUGGGCCAAAUAGGAAAGUGAGCCCCUUAAAGGCAGUUGUCUGACCAGUACUUGGAGCACAACAGGUUCUUGCUAAAGCACUGUGUUUUUAAAACAGUGGAGUUAUUAGGUUGAAAUUCUGAAUAGCAAGAAAAAGAAUAAUGGAAGUGCUGCCAGCCCCGUGAUGCUGGUGCAGCUGGUCAGUUUGCAGAAGGAGGCCAGUUACUAGAGCAGAGUGGCCGUAGAGGCUGCAACACGGUGGCCAAAGCAUGAAGCUGCUGUAUAGUGGCAAGGUCACAGUGAUUUCCCCACAGCCUCGGUUUAGAGGGAGACGGGGUGUGCUGAGCUGUGCCUGCUUCUGUAGAAGGGGCCUUCUCCAAGUCUGAGUAGCCUUAAGCCAUUAGGACUGCUGAGUCUUUCUCCACAAAAAUAUGUGGGAGGCCUGCAGGGCAGGUGCUCAACUAAGCUCUGGGGCUGCAAAGAUCCAGAGCCAUGCCCCUCCUUGGAGGCAGGUCCUUGUAGACGAGGACAAUCGUAGCCUUCCUGAUUAAAGCAGGAAUUGUCCAAUCAGGCUAUAUGACGGGCAUCGUCCAUAGUCUUCACCAGGGGAGCUUUUCUGACUAUACAUCUCUAGCCCUGUGGCUUGAGCCAGUCACUUAAUUUCCCCUGAGCUUUGGUUUCCUCCUCCUGGUAGCAGAGAGACUAUCAGAGUGAGGGGCAGAUGCAAUAGCAUAUGUAAAACACUUAGCGUUGGGCCUGGUGUUUAACUGCAAUAAAUGUUAGCUCAUAUUUUACUGUGACAUAGAUGCUGUAUGCCUUUUGCUGAGUAUUAAAGAUACUGAGCUGUAGCAUGCAUACUUGCAUGAAUCAGUCUGCUAAGUUAUUUUAAGUUUGCAUUUGAAAAUAAAGGGUGGAUUGCUAUCCAAAUAUAAAGAAUUGGAACCAGGCUCUAAAAGGAUGUUUGCUGUUCUUUAGCAAAAUACCAUUCUUCUUAAGUUUCAUUCAAUCAUUCCACAAAAAUUUAAGCAUCUGUUUUGUCCCAGGCAGGCACUGUGCUUGUAAUGGAUGUGCAAUAGCAAACAGAACACUUGCUUUCAGCUCACACAGAGCUGACUCCUGGGCAGAGAAUUUCGACAGUAAAGAAAUACAAGUGUGAUGAAGGAGAAACCCUUUGGUACUACCUGCUACAUGUUUUAAUAUUUAAAUGUUGACUUAGGGAGGUCUUUCCAUCUAAAAAUAAUGAUUUGCCCUUUCUCCUGUAAAUGACCCCUUUCUCUUAAGUUUUGGGUGAGAGAUUUUUUUUUUUUAAGGAAGAAAGAUAUUCUACAAUCGAAUGUACAACUGAGAUAAUGCUUAGGAGAGAAUGUAUACUGGGUUUGUGCCUUGGAAGUUGCUUAGGGGAAACAGUUGUGUGCAGUUGGAAAGCUGAUGCUUUAAAGAAGCUUCUAUAAAGUGACCCCACAAUUAAACUGUUUUGUGUACAUCUUUAUUUAUUUAUUUAUUUAUUUUUUAAUUGAGACAGAGUCUCACCCUUUCGCCCAAGCUGGAGUGCAGUGGUGCGAUCUCGGCUCAUUGCAACCUCCACCUCCCAGGUUCGAGCAAUUCUUCUGCCUCAGCUUCCUGAGUAUCUGAGAUUACAGGCAUGUGCCACCACACCCGGCUAAUUUUUGUAUUUUCAGUAGAGACGGGGUUUUGCCAUGUUGGCCGGGCUGGUCUUGAACUCCUGACCUCAAGUGAUCCACCCACCUCGGCUUUCCAAAGUGCUGGGAUUACAGGCGUGAGCCACCACGCCCAGCCUACGUCUUUAAAAAUAAAUGUAAAUACCCAAGGCUCACAGUUCCGUUCUUCCAUCUAGUCUAGCACCGUCCAGUGGAAGUUUCCACCAUGAUGGACUGUUCUGUGGAUGCCCUGUCCAGUACAGGAGCCGCUAGCCACAUGUGGCUAUGGAGCACUUGAAAUGUGGCUAGUGCUACGGAGGAACUGGAUUUUGGAUUUUUUUAAAGUUUUAAUUUAAAUUUGAAUAGCUACAUGUGGCUAAUGGCUACUGGACAUCACAGAUCUAACACAGGAUUAACUGACAAAAUUCUUUCCUCUUAAAAAUAUGUGUUUAUUUUGAUAAGGAUAACUGAGACCUGUACAUUCCAUUUUUCCUGUCAUAUUUAGGGCUCAUAAAGGGGGUGGUAUGCACGUUUUAAAAAAUGCAACACAACCAGUUAAACCAGCUGUCUAAUUGUACACAUUUCCUGGAGCUGUUGGUGUUGAUUAUUAGCAAAUACUAAGUACUUGUAAUGACCUAAGAACUAUAAGACAAGCAAGUCGUCUUCUGUAACUGAGUAUCAGCGGAUUCAAGCGUUAAGGAAAAUGAUUAAGAGAAAACAACCAAAAAAGUCUUAAUGGUUCUGUCAAUCAAGUGGCUAUCAAUUCAUGGCUAUUCAAAAGCUUUUGUGGCUAUGAAAAUAAACUAGAUUGAAAAAAUUCUAAAACAAAAUUGAAACACUCAUUUGAGUUUAAAAUUUUAGUUGAGUUGAUUUUUAUUUCUUGUUUUGGUUCAUUUGUAGUUUCCCCCCGCUUCGUUGUUUCCUCAGAUAUGGAGAAUAAAGCCUGGCUGGUCAGUUUCAGUUUUUAUUUAAAUUCAUUUUGUCUUCAUUCCUUUUAAUCUAGCACAGUCCUGUGAUGUAUUGGGAUCACAGUGCUCUGGGGAAACAUUGAAAUAUAAAAACAUUUUCCUGAAAACAUUUCCAGUUAUAUUUAAUUUUCCUCCUUGAAUAGAAAAAUAUUUCCAACUUAAUCCUCCCUCUCCCCUCUUGAAAUGAAUUGCAUGCUUUGGAAAUAACAUCAAUCCACCCAAGUACACAAGGACAAUCUCAGCCAUUUAAUCGAGAUAUAAAGGCUUAGAGAACUCUGGGCUUCGGAGGCACAGACUCCACCUUUCAGGAUGCUAAUAAACGUGGACGAGGUCUCGCCUGGGCUUCCUCCUCCAUUGUUCAGCGCAGCAAACCAGCACAGCACUCCGUGGCCAGGGUUUGCGGGGAGAAAUCUCUCACUCUGUUUUAGUAGCAUCAUCAUCCUUAUCAGCACCCUGCUUUUAUUUUUGAACAGCCAAACUUCCUCUUUCCAAACUUCGUGUGACAUCUGGGACCAGCUAUGUUUGAAGGAGUCUGAACAUGCCACAUAGUGGCUCACGCUUUUAAGGGAGGAAGGCCAGUAAGCCUCCUCAAUGGCAGAAUUCUACUUUCAGUCUACCCUUUGGUUCUGUUGUGGUUGUUCCUUAGAACUUUAUUCUGCUCAUUAGGAAGCCCAGCCUCCGGGGAGGGUUUAGCUUCUCAUCUAAGCAAGAAGUAAAAUGUCAUAAUGGAGGAAAAAAAAAAAAAAGUCCAAACUUUUUUUGGACUUUUAGAAACACAUCCAGUUUGAGCUCCACUGAGCUAUCAUUGCAGUUACAAAGCCCAUGUAUAUUGAGAUCGGUGUAAAAAUUCAGCAUGUCCACCUGCAUAAUUAUGACCAGUGUAUUGAAAGCACAUUUCAUUUAGUUUUGCAACAGCCGAUGAGGUAGAUUCUACCAACAUUGUUUUACGGAAGAACAAAUGGAAGCCUGGAAAAAUAAAUUGUCUACCUCACACACUUCGCAGGUGGUAAACACAGGAUUUGAACUAAGACAUACUUGAUUUUAAAGUGUUUGCUUUUCCUUUGCACUACUGCAUCUGCGAUGUUUGCACUCAGACACUCUAGAAUAUUUGGUGUUGCAUGUUUUUGCCCCAAGAAAGAACCCAUUAAAAUGAAACUUUCCAGUUCGUAAGCUUUGCCCUCAAGAAGGGAAAGAACUUCUUGCAAGGUUUCUGAAACAAAAAGAAAAUGAAAAGUAACUUUACUGUAUCUGGGUUUUCUGAUUAAAUUACGGUUUUUGCAAGCUUGUGCAUUUCUCAGUGUCCAGAUAGCCAGGAUUUUUCCUUUUAAUAAAUAUCACUUUAAAAAACAAACACACACAUUCUUAAAUGCAUGAUUAACUGUAUAGAUUGAUUUAGUUAUAAGAUGUCCUAGCCUAAAUAUAAGAAGGUGUAUGUGUUAGAAUUAAUUUCUUCAAUAAAGAGAAAGAAAUUCAGGAAUUGUGGUUCUGUUGGUCUUCUGUACUGUAUAUUUUUGUGCAGCCAAAGCAGCAUGCCUUGCUUCUUGGUUUCAUGACCACAUGGGUAGUUUCUUGAAGUUUUUUCUUUUGAGAUGGAGUCUUGCUCUGUCACCCAGGCUGGAGUGCAGUGACGCGAUCUCGGCUCACUGCAACCUUCACCUCCCGGGUUCAAGCAAUUCUCCUGCCUCAGCCUCCCGAGUAGCUGGAAUUACAGGCAUGUGCCACCAUACCUGGCUAAUUUUUGUAUUUUUAGUAGAGACGGGGUUUCGCCAUGUUGGCCAGGCUGGAGUUUCUUGAAGUAUUGACUGAUCCUUGACUCUGAACUGUAUGAUCAAAGACUUUUGAAAUGGCACACCGUUUCUUAACAUUUAGGCCAAUUUCAGUUGCUCAUAUCCAAAAAUAAGUCAUGAUUUUCGGAGUCAGUGCGCAGCACUUAGUACAACAAUCCAAACCCUUGUACAGACCAUCCUAGUAGAAAUGUGGAUCUUGAGUAUCUCAGCUUCUUAGUAGAUUUUGAACUCCGUGAAAGCAGGAGCCAGGCCUCUCACAGCAAGUCUCUCCAAUAUGCUCAGUAAAUAUUUGUCAGAUCGAGCAAUGACCAGAUGAUGAAAUACAUUAAAGCCUUAGGGAGAACUGAGACUACUGCACCAGUUUUUGUGCACUAUCAUGCUGGAAAUCUUUCCAACAUGUAUUCUGUACUUCUUUGCUUCUUACUCCAGUGAAUAUAAUUUAGUCAUUUCUGGCCAACUUGAGGACAUCAGCGAGCAUAAAUUGUUGUAUUAUGCAUAAUACAGUGAUACCCUCAAGGCUGAGUGGGAGGCAGUUUGCCCUCUGCUGAAGGUUUCUUGUGCUUAUUGUGUUCUUAUGGUUUGGUUUUACCAUUUUUAUGUCUCCAUUUCUGUUUAAUAGACUUAUUUCAGUAAGAAGAGAAAGCCGUCUCCAUCAGCCCCUCUGUAGGUGAUUAUUUGCCACUUCCUUUUUGCUGUGAGUGCUUUGAAAACAGAUUUCUAAGCUUGUUAGAGUUAUGUGUUAAGAGUAAAUAGGCAGUAAGUGAAACCAAGCUUCUUCCUGGUGCUUGACUACCCCAGAAAUGUUUAUUUGCUGAAUAGUUGAGUUCUGGAAAGGUGAGGUAUAAAUGUGUGAUAAAUUUAUUCCUUUGCAUGAUUUUUUUUUCUUUUUCUUCCCUCCCUCCCUCCCUCCAUCUAUGUCUCUGUCUUUCUCUGAACAUCUCUCCGUCUCAGUCUGUCUCUCUCAUGAUAGUUGCUGGAAUAAUUUAAAUGAAUGUAACUCAUUUACCCACAUCGAAGCCCAACUCAGUAGUGAAAAAACAAAUCUUCCAAAUGAAUGCACUUUCCCCUUGAUGUGCUAUAUACAAGACCUUGGCACACCUAGUUCAAUGACAUAGUAUUUUAGAAGGGCCUCCUUACACCUUCCUCUCAGAUAAAUAUACAUGCAGGGACAUUCUGAAGAAGUUUGUUAUCGGUCUUCUCCCCUCCUACUAUUAGCUCCGCCCUCCUAGUCCUUCUCUUUCACCAUGCUGACCCGCGUAGGGAGGACCCUUACACCCUCUGCAUGCAGCGCUGGUGCUCCUUAGUGUUCAUAACCCCAACCUCCAUGGCCUCUCUCGCAGUUCUCAGGUUAGGCCCUGCUUCUAGGGGACAUUAGCUUUCCACCCUCUACUACAUACUUCCUAGUUGUUGCAGCCUUUGCAAGCAAAACUUGUUUUCAUUUGGGAGACAGCAUGGUCUGACAGAGCCUAGAUCCUGGGGUGAAGACAUUCUGGGUUUGUAUCCCGUCUUUACCACCUCUGAGCCUCUGAUGCUGGACAAGUCAGCAAGUCUUUGCACCUUAGUCUCCUUUCUGUAAAAAGGAGCUUAUGGGGAUGUAAUCAGAGAAGCCUUAGCAUGGCUCUUGGUACAAGGCACGGACCAAAUCCAUGGUACGCUCACUCCUUUCCUUUCAGUAAUACUGCCUAAAUAGGGCACAUGUACCUAAAAGGAUUUUGUACAUUCCUUGACAGCAGAAUUCUCAUCUUCUGUUGCAUAUCCCAUAAUGCUGGGAACACAAAAUAAAAAUGGUAGCUUUUCACAUUCACUUUUGGCCUCAAUUUUUUGUUAUUCCCCAAUGAGGAUCAUUUCAUUUGGGGCUGGUCUCCGGAAAAAAGUAGAUCAAGCUUUUCAGAUGAGAUUUGGGUGAAACCCUGACAAACUCUUUUUAUUGCCUUCCCUACCACAUAGUGGUGGAUCAGGAAACUGUAGGGCUUAUGAUGCUGGGAAAUUUCUGCUAAUGCAAUAAAGAUUUUUGCUGUUGAAAGAAUUUGAUCUGUUUUAUGUAUAACAUGCAGAGAGCAGAAGCAUAUAUUAUCUGUAGCAGAUGAUAGAGCAGGGUAUAUGGGCAAGUUAGAAAAACACAGUUCUCACUACAUUUGAAGAAAAAGGACAAGGAGUUGUCACAAGGAUCCAGGAGAGUCGCACAUAAUUUUCUGUCGUGCAUUUUGUUGACUGUUCCUCUUUGCAUCCUUCAACCAUCUUAACUUCCCACUUGCACCUCGCUGGAAGACAAAUCUAAGCUAAAUUAAAUGCUAGGCAAUAUGUCAGAAUGGAAAGGGCCCUCAACUUGGGAUGCCCGGUUCUCUACCAGCCUGAAUAAACUCCAGCAACAGUAUUUCUCUAGGAAUCAUCUGUAAAAAGUAGAGGUUUGUCAUAUCUCUAAACUAGGGAUUCACCUUAUUUAUUAAGCUAUCAGUGACUUUAUCUUGAGGUGCACGGCUUUUAGUAACUCUGGUUCAAGUGCAAGGAAUGCAAAGUUAAGUGUAUCAUUGGAGGUGGGAUUUUUGAGUUUGUCAGUCAUUUAUUGAUUUGCAUGUAUCCUUAUAGUUCAAAGGUCUUUUUCUCAACUUAGUUGAUGAUCAUGCUGUAAGUUGUUUUCUUUUGCUUUAUCAACUUUUAAAAACGUUUAUUAACUUUUUAAUUUGAAAUAAUUUCAGACUUGCAUAAAGGUUACAAAGAGUACCAGGAGUUCUGGAACACCCUCCACCCAGCUUCCACAGAUGUUAACAUCUUACAUAACCGUAAUACGGUUAUCAAAACAGUGUUCACUCCAUACUCCAGUGCUGUUAAUCUCCAGACUGAAUUCGGAUUUCACUAUUUUCCCACUGAUGUCCCUUUUUUUGGUUCCAGAUCCAAGAGACGAUCCUACCUGGCAUUUAUUGUGUUCAGUUUUUCUAAUUCUGGGACGUUUUCCUGGGUUUUCUUUAGUCAUUCACGAAGUUCGCACUUUUGGAGAACAUGGGGCCAGUUAUUUUGUAGAAUAUCUUUCUGUUAGAGUUUGUGGAUGUUUCCUCCUGAUUAAAUUUGGGGGGUACAUUUUUAACUUGGAGAUCACAGAGGUGCUGCUGUUUGUGUCUUUGCGCAUCCUGUCAGGAGAUGCGUGAUGUUUCCUUUCCUGGUGCUGUUAGCUUUGAUCCCUUAGUUAAGGUGGUCUCUGUGGCUUCCUCCAUUAUCAUUACUAUUUUUCUCUUUGUAAUUAGGAAGAAUCUUUUGGAGGUAGAUACUUGAGACUAUCUAAACAAGCAUUCUGUUCCUCAUUAUUCUUUCACCCACUAAUUUUAACAUCCAUUACUGUGAUGUUUGCCAAAUGGUGAUUUUCUAUUUCUGUUUUCUACACUUAGUAAUUGGAUUCUACUCUCAGGAUUUUAUGUAUUUUUUAACAGUGAGGGACAUAAACUUUUUAACUAGCAGUGGCAAGUCCACUUUUAUUUGGGAGGACAAUUACUAGUCACAUGAAGAAGAAAAAAUAUGCAGAAGCUUAAGAAAUCCCACAUAUGAAUGUUAUUUGAAAUGUUCUUGCCCUUUCUCCCUACAAAGGAGGUGAAGAAGAUGACAGGAGAUGUUAAUUGCCAAAAUAGUCUCAUAGUUUUGGUCCUGGCUGCAAAUCUCUCGUUUUUGAUACUCAAGAGAAUGCUAUUGGGGAACUGACUCUGAAGCACAGCCCAGAUGCUUGAGAUGGGUUGGGAAGGUUUACAUCAACACCAUGAAUUUAAUUUAUCAUGUGACAUUUUAUUUCUGAGUUUUUAAAGCUGUAAUUAAAAGAAGUGUUCAAAGUGUUGCUUUCCUCUUUUAGAAUAAACGUGGCUGGGUGUGGUGCCUCAUGCCUGUUAUCCCAGCACUUUGGGAGGCCAUAGGCAAGAGGAUUGCUUGAGCCAGGAGUUUGGGACCAGCUUGGGCAACAUAGGGAAACCACAUCACUACAAAAAAAAAAAUUAGCCUGUCAUGGUAGCAUGCACCUGUGGUCCCACUUACUUGGGAGGCUGAGGUGGGAGGAUCACCUGAGUUCAGGAGGUCAAAGCUGCAGUGAGGUGUGAUCAUGCCCCUGCUCUCCAGCCUGGACAACAGAGCAAGACACUGUCUCAAAUAAAUAGGCAAACAUUACCAACAUGGCAAACAAGUUGGAGGAGGCCCCCUAUUUAAUUAAAUUUCAGCAGUCCCAAAUCUAAUUGGUAUGAAGAAAUCAUUAUUCAGAAUUUUCCAUCACUGAAAUACUAAAAUCACUUGUUGUUUGAGACAUCUUGGCCUGUCACCCAGGCUGGAGUGCAGUGUUGCUCUCAUAGCUCACUGGAGCAGGAGCCUCAACCUCCCAGGUUUAAGUUAAUGCUCCCACCUCAGCCUCCUGAGUAACUGCCACUACAGGCGUGUGCCACCAUGCCCAGCUAAUUUUUUAAUUUUUCGUAGAGAUGGGGUCUGUGUUGCCCAGGUCCCUCUUGAACUCCUGGCCUCAAGCUAUCUUCUCCAGUCGGCCUCCCAAAGGGCUGUGAUUACAGGCGGGAGCCACAGCGCUCAGCCUAAAAAUAACUCUUUAGCCAAAAGAAAGUUUUAAAAAAUUGUCUGUUGUAUUCUUUGAUUUUACUCUAUGUGGUCUUUUCUAUUAUUUUUAAAAUAAAAAAGAUUUAUACUCCUCAAGUGUAACAUUUUAUCAAAUCUCAUGCUUCUGUUUGAUGAAACCGAAUGGCUAAAUUUUUUAAAUAUCAUGCAAUCCAUCCCAGUUUGUAAUUUUAUUAUGGCCCUCACACAAGAGCGUGCAAGCUAUACUAAGCUUCCUGUGGCCCUCGUUUUUCCUCACUGAUAUUUGUAACUCAUUCCAAAUUAAAUUUUAGGAGUCUGAAAUGUAGCUGUUAUAUUUGGGAGAUGUGAAGAAAAGAAUCGUAGGCAUCUCAGUAGGCUAGGUAUCAGAUCACACAUGCUUGCUGGACCAAAGAGGACUCCUUACAGUAGGAUACAUGAUUCUGAGUUAGUUUGUGUACUAAGUAUAUACUAUAUAGCUUUUGAAGGGGAGACGGGCACAGAAUUCACAAUAUCAUGCACUAAGGGUUAUUUUGUGUUUGCAGUUUCCAGAUGAAUGUUUUAAAGUUGGCUGCAGAAUACAGCGAGAUAGGUAAAAUCUAUUUGAGUAUUACUUACAGACCCCAAAGGAUAUCCCAAAGGAUAUGUUGGACUAAUUCCUAAAAUAUCCUGUAAGUCAUUGCAGGUACAGGCGUGGAUCUGGGUUUGGAAACGCCGCCUGGAUCGCUGGCUGGGCUCCUGCAGCCGCCAAGGAGGGGCUGGCUGGAGGUGGGGCUCGGCGUGCAUAGCGGCCACGUGACUGCGCCCCGGCCACGCCCACCGUCCCUCACGUGGUCCCAGGCCACGCUGGGCUUCGGCAUGUGCUAAAGUGGAUAGAAAAGGGAGUGGGGCCCGGGCGUGGCUUUGUGGUUUGGGAAGAUAUGAACUCCUUGGGGUUUUUUUCUCUUUUAAUUCUUUAAUUUUGAUAUUUGGAAAUGCGUAAAAGGUUUUUCAUUUGUCCUUGACCACGUGGUCCAAACCUCAAUUUCCCUAGCAGAACGCGGUUUCGAUCACUGGUGGAUCCGUCUCACAGCACCAGUCAUGCUGCCUCGCUGGGAAGUGGAGGGCUCAGGAUUCCCGUGGUUCACGAUCCAUUUUAUGUUGGAAGGAAAUCAUUUUGAACUAUCUCAGUACACACCCUAGUGUAUCUUUAAACCUAAUUGAGUGUUGAUGGAAAAUCUGCGGUCCGAGAACCGUAAGAAAAGGGGGCUCCCACCUCCCGCUCUGGGGUCGCCACUUGCCUCGCAGGCAGGAGGAGGCUCCCAGAGUAGAUACAACUUGCCCGUCACCCGGAUGGGUUGGUAGUGCACAUAUGCACGGGGCGCAGUUUAAAAUGAAAGUAAAAGAUGCAAAUGUGUUUGCAAAAGAAAAAUUAACAUAGGAUACGUGCGGGCGUUCUCAGUUGAACUCGGUCUUACUGUUCCACGCGAGCACCCCAUGACUCAGAGCCCAAAUCUCAGCGGAACAGCCCAGGACGCUCCUGCCGUCCACAGGAAGACGCCUCUGUCUCUGUCCCCCGCCGCCACCACACAGAUGCACGUACUCUCUUCACUUCCGUGUACCCAGUAAAUGCAGAUCCUGAUUUAAAUCUGCAGCACGCUGCUUUCUUCCCAUUGCAUGUGGGAAGCUUCAGGUUCUCUUCGGUUUAUUUUCUCAUCACCUUUAUUAAAAUGCAGUAAAGCAAGGAGUAUAUUAAUGCGGGCCUCUGCAAAUAGAGGGAAUUUAUUGAAAAGCAGAAUGGCUUGAAAGAUUGAACUUCAUCUUAAAAAUCAGAAACAGACUCUUGUUAUUAAUAGCUUUAGAAACGAAAAUCUAACUUCUGAUAAAUUAUUUCAGAGGAGUGGUUCAAACGUGUAGUAGAUAGCUCUGCCUGGUCAUCAAUUAUAGUGACGUCCUUGCAUCAGCUCCAGAAACUCAGAAUAUUCAUGAGCUUUCCAGUCUGACUCAGACCUUCAGGAGCCAUGAAAUUUUCCUGUUGGGAUGAGAGGAAGCGCUGGCGGUCGUUUCGGCAGCUUAAUGAAACCAGAAAUAGAUAAGCACGAGUGAGGGGUGAUGUCCGCUUGUUUGCUCCCAUCAUGUUGUUUUUAAUGUGUGAAAGUGAAAGUUUUAAAAGUCAUACUAAAUGUGUGAUCCUUUUUAGAAUUCACUGGGUACGGGUACGUGGAGGAAGUGUUUUUGUUUUUGUGAAUUUGUUUAAACAAAUGACUGAGGCUUUGUUUUCCACUCUGUCUGGCCAAGCACCAUUGCUACACUUUUUUAAAUUCAUGACAUCCUGAGCAGUGAAGCUGUUCUUCAGCCCGCCUCUCCAUUUGUGACUGGAAGACAAGGAGGCAGACACCAAUGGCGCCUCUCACAAUGGAGGUUUAUUUUUUUUUAAUCUAACGGAGGGAUUGUAGAUGGUGUAAAACUUCCUUGUGCCAGGAGAGAAAGGGGGAGAGAGAGAGAGAGAGAGAGAGAGAGAGAAAUAACCCAUUCUAAACAACUUUAGGAAUAGAUGAUCCGUAGGCAUCAACUUUGCGCAGCAACAAAAGCCACUUUCUGAACCUCGUUCUGUGAAGUUUUAAAACAAAUUGGGUUUGUUUAAUUAAAAUAUUUCUUAAAGGCAAAAAGCACUGAGCUAAUUUUUAAGAAUUUUAAGUUAUAUAUUAAUAUGAGUAGUGAUUUAUAAUUUUCUGUUGAAAUACAUAAAUUCGAGAAGCCCCACCCCUACCACUUGCCAGUCUUGAGUCCCCACGGCUCCUUUGCCUAGGUCUAAAGUCACUGCUUGCACACUCCUGCCUUGCAUAUGCCUUGCCAUCGUGUGGGCCUCUUGGCUGGAAGUGUUCUUGUCCUCCCGUUAGGUAUCUUUUAUGACGUGAAUCCUUACCUCUAAUUAUUAUCUGUGUGUACAUCUCAUCACCUGCAUCUGACUGUGUGCCUUGUGUAUGUCUCUUAGCCCUCACAAUUGCCUGACAUGCCUUACAAACGGGUAGACCAAGUGUUAAAUGAACAAAUAUUUAAUAAGAACUUAAAAGCUUUUUGACUUUAUAUAUUUUUAAAGCCAUUGUGAUUAAACACUAUGUUUGAUGUGGUGCUAAUUCUGUGCUUUAUCAACUGUGUGAAUUGUAGUAUUUUUAAAGUAGGAAUAAUUGAGAAAUAUUUUGAAGUUAGGUUAAGCAUAGCAGUAAAGUUUCCACUUUUUAAAAUAGCCAAAUCCAGGCCAGGCGCAGUGGCUCGUGUCUCCAAUGUCAGCACUUUGGGAGGCCAGGGCGGGCAGAUCGCUUGAGGUCGGGAGUUCGAGACUAGCCUGGCCAACGUGACGAAACCCCGUCUCUGCUAAAAAUACAAAAAUUAGAUGGUUGUGGUGGUGCAUGCCUGUAAUCCCAGCUACUCAGAGAAGUGUUUGAACCCGGGAGUUGGGGGUUGCAGUGAGUUGAGAUUUCACCACUGCACUCCAGCUGGGGCAAAAGAAUGAGUGAAACUCUGUCUCCAAAAAAAAAUCAGAGCGUGGUGGUGCACACCUGUAGUCCCAGAUACUUGGGAGGCUGAGAUGGAGGUCAAGGCUUCAGUGAGCCAUGAUGGCACCACUGCACUCCAGCCUGGACAACAGAGUAAGACCUUGUCUCCAAAAAAAAAAAAAAAAAGCCAAAUCUGUUGGGUUUUUUUUUUUGGGGGGGGGGUCCUUUAGAAUGGCCCUGACAGAUCUUUAAGGCAUGGAAAUGAGCCUUAUGCAAGCUCCUGGCAAUCAGUAUGUGAGUUCUGUCUCCUUGGCAAGAUACAGCCUCUUAGACCCUCAGUCUGGGGAAAUAAUGCUGAUUUCUCCUACGAGUUACGAGAAUUACGCUAGAAAACUCUGUGGCGCAUACAGGUGCCCUGUAGCCUGUUGGUUAGAAGCACUGACCCUGAAGUCAGGUCGCCCAGGUUGGAAUUCCAGCUCUGCCUUCUUCAAGCUGUGUGACUCUGGGAAGUCACACACACUCUCUCUUUGUGCCUCAGGCUCUGGUUCUGAAGAUGGGAACGGCAGGCCCUCCCUCUUUGGCUUGUUGCACAGAUGAAAUCUGACAGCGUAUGCCAAGCGCUUAGCACGGGUAGCAGUGAGUGCCCCGUAAAUGUUAGGUACCUUCCUACUACUACUAAACAUUCAUUCUUCCCUUCCCUGCUAGUACCUGCAGCUCUGACUCAUCUCACACCCUUGAGAGAGGAUUAUCUUCAUUAAAAAGUUUUUGGUCUGCCCAGAAGCAAGUGUUACCUGUGAGAGAGCUGGGCUUGUGCAUAGGUUAGAUUAUUUCUUUGGGUUAUUCCUGGGGAAACCUGCAAAGAAAUGCAGCCAGAGGCCUCUGGUUCAUUUUACUGCUCAUCUCCUAAAAGUGGUUUCUCAGAUUUUUAUCCUUUUUUUCUCUUUUUCGAGGAAGGGGCAAGGAAAUAUUUUUUCAUAUUAUUCUUGUCAUCGUCUAUUUAUUUAAUAACAGUUGACUGUUGAAACAUAGGAAAGUACUUAUCCGCCAGGAAACUCCCUUCUAUUAUUGGACUUACUUGCUUUCCAUUUAUAUGUUGUCUAAUUCCAAAGAGAUUUCGAGACAGCUUUCAAUUAAAAAAAACAAACAACAACAACAACAAAAAAAAACACCACAUACCGCAUGGGUAUUACACAGGACCUGUAUGGUCAAAUUGGCAACGACCACACCACAUGAGAAGGAAGAUUAUUCUUCCUGGAACCUGGCUCCCUUGAGAUUCUUUUUUUUUUUUUUUUUUAGACGGCGUUUCGCCCUUGUUGCCCAGGCUGGAGUGCAAUGGCACGAUCUCCGGCUCACCGCAACCUCCACCUCUCGGGUUCAAGCGAUUCUCCUGCCUCAGCCUCCCGAGUAGCUGGGAUUACAGGCAUGUGCCACCACACUCGGCUAAUUUUGUGUUUUUAGUAGAGAUGGGGUUUCUCCAUGUUGGUCAGGGUGGUCUCGAACUCCCAUCCUCAGGUGAUCCACGCGCCUCACCCUCCCAAAGUGCUGGGAUUACAGGCAUGAACCACCGCACUCCCUUGAGAUUCUUGUAAGCCAAGGCAGAAGAAGAGACAUCUUAAAGUCUGUAUGUGCACACCUGCCUCCCCCCAUUUUAUAUACAAUUCAAGGGCUUUGCUUUUGGAAAGUUUGCCUAUGUAGUCGUCCAGGGCUAAAUUAACACCUGUCUCUAUCUGUGUGUAAGGCUCUCUGGGAGGAGCUGUGAGGCAAAUAAAAAUAAGGAAUGGUGUCCCGCAAGGAGCUUACAAUGUGUGCAUUACAAGUAUAUACUGAGCAUGGCCCUGGGAACACAGUGAAAAAACAGGAUUCCUGCCCUAGUACAGUGUACACUAGUGGAAGAGAGAGAGGCAGUAAACCUAAAAGUAAGUCUUUUAAAAACUGUGGUAAAAUGCACAUAACAUAAAAUUUACCAUCCAACCGUUUUUAUGUGUACAGUUCAGUGACAGUAAGAACAUUCACAUUGUUUUGCAGCCGUGACCAUCAUUUAUAUUCAGAACUCUUUUCAUCUCGCACAACUGAAGUUGUACCUAUUAAACAGUAACUCCUCAUUCUCUCUUCCACCUAGGCCCUGGCCAAAAACAAAAAUAAGUCUUUGAUUGUAAACACGAUCAGUGCUUUGAAGGAGAUGGGAAGGAUGUUAUCAUAAAAUGAUGGGGCUGCAGGAAUGGCACCUACUCAGAGAGGGCGGUCAGGAGAGACCUCUUGGGAAUGAUGACAUCCAGCAGGCAGGUCAUUAAGGCAUCUCUAGGCAGGUCCAGAGUGCAAGGAGGCAUAAGCCAGGCAGGUGGAACAGCGUGUGUGAAGGCCCAGAGUCAGGAAAUGGUCUGCUUCCUUCCAAGGAAAAGAAAACAGCCAGUGUGGUUGGAGCAGGGGCUAGGAGAGAAAAGAUGUGCAUGUGUGUGUGUGUUUGUGUAUCCCCAUCAUGAUUUAGUACUGUCAGCGCUUCUGUGUUCUGAACCUGGAGUACAGGCAGACACAGCCGCAUCCCAGAAGCUCAAGAGUGCCCAUACCAGGAAAUUACAGAAAUCUUUGCCAAAUGGAUGAGUGAAUGCAACUUCCUUGAUACAGGGUCAGAGAGGGGAAAUCUGAGAAAAGCAGGUGGGCAAUGUACUCCUGACAUACUCCCUUCCGUUGCAAUGGCCUUGAGUGAUGGAGCAAGAGUGAAGGAAUGUUCCCAUGGCACUGGCACCAGGAUGACUUUUUGUGAAGCAGAGCAGUUGGUCUUAGAUAGUGGAGGUGCGGGAGGCAUGAGAACUGGGCAGUCUGACGGCUGCACCAGCCAGUUGGCUGUCCUUUCCACCUCCAUGCCCAGGAGCUGGCCCAGGGCGCGCAUGCACAAAGCCAGUGCUCUUUUCAAUCAGAAAACAGCCUGCGUAUGUUCUUGCUUGCAACUCAGAUAUCCAGCCCACUGAUCCAGGAAGAGAUUCCUUUGACCUGGGAAGUCAUAAUGGCAGAUAUUUAGACCCAGCUCUCAAGCAAGCAUCCAAGUUGUUCCGGUGAACCCGUAACUUUGAGUAACCUCUGAUUGAACCAGAGAGUAGGAACUAGGUGCAGAACCUUGUUGAAUAGAAUUGUUUAGCAUCGUCCAUUUGUUAGAGCAUUUCAGGAUGCCUGUCCUAAAAUUUGGUAUCAUAAUGGUAUUUACCUCUCACUCACCUCCAUCUCAGCCCAGUAAUUAAUAACAAGGGACUUGCUUCUUCACCUGUUUCUUUAUUGGUUGUAGGAAGUCUUUUCCUUACCACAGAGGAAGGAGCUUCUGGAUCCCUUUGCUACGUCCAGAGAGUUUUCAUCUAAUCUGGGUGUAUUAGUCCAUUUUCACACUGCUGAUAAAGACAUACUCAAGACUGGGCAAUUUACAAAAGAAAGAAGUUUAUUGGACUCACAGUUUCAUGUGACUGGAGAGGCCUCAAAAUCAUGGCGGAAAGUGAAAGGUACAUCUCACAUGGCAGCAGCCAAGAGAAGAAGAGCUUGUGCAGGGAAACUUCCAUUUUAAAAACCAUCAGAUCUUGUGAGACAUAUUAACUAAUAACAGCAAGGGAAAAACCCACCCCAUGAUUCAGUUAGCUCCCGGCGGGUCCCUCCCACAACAUGUGGGAAUUAUAGGAGCUACAAGAUGAGAUUUGGGUGGGGACACAGAGCCAAACCAUAUCACUGUGUAAAAGUUGAAUAAAGUUAUUUAGGAGCACAUUGUAUUGGGAGUUUGUUUGUUUGUUGAAGAGCCAAGUAAAGUCAUUGGAAGCAUGGGAAACUUUUUUCCCUGUCUAAAAGGAACUCCUUCCUAGUGGAAGUUGAAAGCUUUCUUGGCAGCCUCAGCCCCCACCCUACCUCCACCACCCCAGUGGGUACCUGCAUCCUGAAGACCCUUCACAAUAGCAUCUGAACUAUACUGGGCCUUCAAAUGAUGUCUUGGGUAAACCCAUGUCCAACCUGCACUAAAUGAAGAUUAUUUUCGAGCGAAUGGAUUGAAGAACAGUGCUGAAAAACUAGAAUUUGUAAUAUUUUCAUUUGAGCAGAGGUGAAAUUUGAAAUAUUUUAGAAUCUUGUCUUAUGAUUUUUUUUCUUUCUUUGCCACAUAGCCCUCCCCUGGAAAUUAAAUCUGUGGAUUACUAGUAUAUGAACUGAUCAGAGACAUGGCUUGGGGUCUCCCCAUUUACCCACUUCCCAGCACGUUAUAAUCCACUGGACACCUCCAAGGAUGAGAGACCAGCGGGUCAUAAUGCGAGACUGGACAUCUCUCCUACCCCAUGUACACUUCAGCUGAGCAGGCAGAAUUAGCAGAGUCAGGACUAGAAGUUCAGUCUAGGGAUCAAAUAAUAAUAGUAGCUAAUGUUUAAAGAGUACCUAAGAUCCGCCAGGAGACAUACUCAGUAUAGUUCCGUGGUUUGCCACAUUUCAUCUUAUACCAGUAGCACAGGUGAAAUUUGUCUUAUGUGUAUACUGAGGAAAACAAGUCCCUCUGAUACACAGCAGCCAAUAAAUGACAAAGCUGGGAUAGAAACUUACUUCAUUCUAACCCGAGAGUCCCUGUUCUUGCAUGGGCACAGCCUGCCAUCCCCAUGCUCUGCCUCCUAAGCAGAGGAUGAACUUAAGCAUCUUAAAAUUUUAAACAUUGACUUUCCCUAAAACCAAUUAAAAAAAAAAACAAAACAGACAGACAGACAUGACUUGUGCCCUUAAAAAUGCAGCCAGGCUGGCAUAUAAAUGGGCGUAGGCUGUUUCUAAAUUUUUUGCUUUAAAUUUUGCCAGCAUAGCUUCUGGACUGGUAGUUUUGUUUGCUUUUUAAUAUAUUUUUGACACUGUGUACAGAGGAAUGCUACCUCGCGUCAUCAUGUCCUCCUCCCUGAAGGCAAGCCAAGGAUGUCAAGGGGCCACUUCAGGGGAUGUGCACCCUGAAGGUAAAGCUGCUCCAGUGGGAGGGGUUGGGGUAAAUGACAAUGUUAGCAGCUGGUAAAUUUUUUUACAUGGGAUAUCUCACAAGACUUAUUGAUGCAUGUUAUACGUAAUAACCUGAGGCACAUCAACAUUUUCCACUUUUUCCUAUUCUUUCUGUAUUUUCACUGAUACUUUUUUUCAAAAAAAUCUCCAAUAAGUUUAGGAUCAGCUUCAAGAUUUCUCUUUAGGUAAAUAGAUUUGUAUUUUUGAUGGCCAUCCUAGUCCAGUGUAAAGAUAUGGACAAGAAACCCCACAUAAAGGAAGCAAGAUCGCUGGCUGCUUUCUCUAGGUAGCUUGAGUUGUAUACUAAUUUGUAGAUUAUUUCUCUUCAUCGAAAAAACAAAACAUUCUGCAGAGGGCAGUCAUGUGUCCGCUGUGCCUCUGCUCCUGUGUGCACCAUAAAACUUGAAAGUGAGCCAGAAUUUGAAAAUAUCGGAUUGGGAUGUGAUUUCUUUAAGCCUCUGGCUAAUUUAAUAUAAAGUGUUUACACUUCAUUUUUCUGGCAGUGGAUUUUCUAUGUAGGUGGUGGAAGAUUUCCUGUAAGUUUUGCAAGUUCCAGGGCAAAGAGAGUUGCAAUAUGCAAUAUCUUUCUGUGGUCACACCAACAGAAAGGGCGAUUUCUUAACCUGCUGCAGUUACCAUGUGUGUAGGUGGAUGCUGGCUAUUACAGAUGGUAUCCUUUCAACCCUCAAAAUUGUUGCAAGUUCACAGGUAUGUUAAUGAAAAUGAAUAAGUGGCAUUUUUAGGAAUUCCAAAUACUGAGUCUUGGAAGUAGAUAAUCUUUUCCCUAAAUGUAUGCUCCGGUCAGAACUGCUGCCUACCACACCUCGUGGGUGAAACAGAUAUUUCGAGCAUGACUGAGCUUAUUAAGAGCCCUGCGGCGCUUCCUCUGCCGGGGGUUUAGAAAUUUCAAAGGAUGGGGGUUGAGGGAGGGAGGAGUUAUGGGCAUGUGAUGUGGACAGGGCGGGCAGGAGGAUGGAAGUAACAGGUCCAAAAUGUAUCUUUGGUGGCCCGGCAGAGCUCUUGCAUGGGGUGAGAAUGGUAAUUUAGGAAGAGCAAGUCUUCCCAUCUGUGAAGCAGAAGAAAAAAGUGGACUUAAGGAGAAGUUCGGGUGCUGUUUAUUUAGAUAGGAGUAAGGAGAGUGCAGUUGGGGAAAAGCACUUCAGAGGCUUUACUUAGACUAGCAGAAGUCUGUUUGGCAGGGUGGGAAGCAAGUGCAGUUGGGAGAAAAACGUUUUCAAUAGGCAGUUUCAGAAUUGGAAAUUGGAGGAGGGCAGUCCAUUUCAACAUUUCCAACAGUAUUAAAGAAAAUUUGCGGGUUGUUUGUCAAAAGGGGUCAUAUGCUUUAAAGAUUGAGAGAUCUUUUCGGUGAAGUAGGGGAGCUGGGGACAUCGUGAUGUGACAAGAGCCGUGGGCUCAGAGGCUGGGGACCUGGGUGUUUAACCCAACUCUUGUGAGUGGUGUGGCUUUCAUAGCUUUGGUUCUCUGGUCUUCACUUUAUCUGCCAAGUGAAGACAUUUGACUGGAUGUCGUGAUCUUGAGUUGCUUUCAGCUCCAGAAUUCGAAGACCCCUUCCAUUGGGCAUUCAUCUAAUUUCAAAGAUGCUCCCUGGCUCCAGCUCUGCAGUGAAGCAGAACAAACUGAUACAGCCUAGCUUGGGGGUGGGGAGUCGGCCCUCCUUUUCCCCUCCCUUCCCAGGUCCUCUGGGUGAUUGGGGGAAACUGAGAAGCCGUUCUCUUCUCCAGAGCACUCCAUUUAACAAGCAUUGCAGAGCCUGGCUCGUGCUGCAGUGAACAAAUGCUGACUUCAGCCUUUACCCUGGGUUUCAGGUCACACUGAUUGUUUGCAAAACAUGUUCUUUUUUUGUCACUUGCCAGUACUUGUUCUCUGUGAGUAAAACACAAACACAUCCUCAGGGAUGUUGCACACCAGUUUGCAGCCUGCAGCUUCUGCCCUCUGGCCUGCCCAGGUCCUCGGCUCCGGGACGAGGAUGCUCCGGGAUUUCGGGAGACAGCAGUUGUUUUGACAUGAAUCUCAAAGUUCCUACAAAGCUUAUUUCUUUGAAGAAGGCCAAAAAAAAAAAUGAAACAUUUUCAGAUCUUUGUUUUCAGAUUAUUCAAGUCCAGAAUGUUGGAUAAGAUUUUUGAAGAAGAGAUUUAUGCUUGAGAUUCCUUUUAGUUUCUUUCUUUCUUUUCUUUUCUUUUCUUUUUUUUUUUUUUUUAGGUGACUUGGCCAGUUUGGGUUUUUACGGUGUUCAGGGAAAGGGUUAAGAAGUUAAUUUGGGAAGUACAGUCAUGUGUUGUACAAGUUGCUGUCUACUGAUCCCUUCAUUGAGCAAGUAAACUUCACACAUUCUCGUGUCUGCAAAGCAUGUGGAUGCAUGGGCAGUUAUGUGUAUGAACUUUUUUUUUUUUUGAGAAUGGCUUUAGUGUUCAGACCAAGGAUGGAAUGAAAGAUCACGUGUGCUUUCCACUGUAGAGCUGCCCUGCUUGUUUUGAUUUUAUAGUUAUUCUAAGUGUUAAGUUCCUUCAUCUUUCAAAGCAAAUUCCUUUGAUCCCUGAAAAUCAGCUAAUGUUUGGGAGGCAAUUAAAAGAUGAGGCUGUGGGGUUGGGGUGAAGGCUUCCCCAGCAGGAAGAGAGGAGAAGCCCACUGGAUCUGGGAGCACGGUGCUAGGACUCUCUAAGCGUGACCUCCUUCAGUUUGGCCCAGAGUGGUCAGAUAGUUUGCCGGGGCAUAGGAUGGAUGACAGGCCUCAUACGCAUCACGUCUGAAGGGAAAGCCCUUGAAUUUUCCACGCUACUUUUUAGUAACAGUAGGCUUUGUCAUAAUUGGCUUCAUGUUCCAGCUUUCCUAAAACUGUAAGUGAUGUUGGGUGGGCCAGCAGCAAAAUAAUUCACUUUACAAUUUGCAUGAUAGUCUGGAAUGAACCGAAUACCUAAAACCAGGAAAUAAUAGUAGAUAUUUAAUGGUUUGGGGAUCAAAUAAGAAUUUACUCCCAGAUGUUUCCUAAUUAAUUGGAAAAAGCAGAAGGUUGCUGGAAGGCCAUCUCCAUUGGGCAUUUACAGGUGAAAUUCACUCUUCAACUAGGAUUUUACUCAUGGGAUGCCUGUGUUCUUCAUUUGAACCCAAUUUUACCUAUCAUCUACAAAAAAAGAAAACUAUUAAGAGUUAAAAAAAAAAAAAGAGAGAGAGAGUCUUGAACUUUGAAAUCCUUCAUCCACGUUUUAUAAAGUGUGGGGUCAGAUUUUUUCCCUAGUUGAAAUUGAGGAAAUGAGAGUUGCCAAUAUGAUUGGAUUUGUACUGCCAAGAUGGGGUUUUAGCACUUCUAAUGCAUUCUGGCAAGGCUGGUAUACUUGUAUCAAGUGCACAGCCCCACUACCACCAGCUCUACCACCCACAAAAAUAAAAACUAGCAAAAUAAAAUAUGAGCCAACAGAAUUCUGUGGGAAUGGCAAGUGUUUUGUUUUUGUUUUUAGUAGUAAUCUUUGCGAGAACAUUCCAAAGAUGAUAGUUUUACAUUUGUAUGUUUUUUUCCGAGGCACUUUUGAAUCAUCAGAUAGAUUAAAUAUAAGUUCCAUGUAUUUUUGAAGGUGGGAGUGUUCUUUGGUACAGUUCCCCCAAAAAACUGGUUCUCAUGAGGCUUAUGUGGUAAUUCUGUUAACGAGAAUGUAUGAUUAUCUGGGAUACUCUGUUCUGCUCUCCAUCCUGGAUAAGAGUUUACUUUGAAAGUCUAGUUGAUCUUUUGUGAUUUCUGCACAAUGUAAAAGGUACUUUAACUUCAGGAGAUAGGGCCAGCAAUCAGAUUUGAUGAUGGAAAAGAGUAGUGUAGCAUUUAAGCAUAAUGUAUACUCUAUAAUAAAUGUUUACAAGUCCAAAAGUGUGCCAUCAGAAAGUAACCAGAUCAAAGGAGAGGUGACCAGAGAAGCUGGAAAGAUAAGAAAUAAACAAGUUUCAAGGUUACUGAUCUGUAGCUGUUGCUGUCCAUGCUUCUUGGCAGCUUUAAUUAUGACAGGGAGAGGGACCCAGAGGGAGAGAGAGAGACUGACUUACACAUAAAGGCAUUUUAUCACAAAGCCAUCUAAAACAAAAGUGUUAAAGGCACAAUGCUGUGUUUAAAAAGCAUGUACUUCUUUAAGAGCUCAAAUUUAAAUAUAUAAUACAAACUUAAGAUCCAAGGAAGAAAAUGGACCCAGGACACGAAGAGAAGUUAACGCCACAGGUAAUGCAGAUGGCCAAGAGAUGUGUGAAAAAGAUAAUCCAGCCUCACCAACAGCCACAGAAUUGAAAUGAGAUACCUGUUUCUGCUUCUGGCAUUGGGAAAGAAAGAAAAAUGGCACUAGCAGCCUUUUUUUUUUUUUUUUUUUUUUUUCCCCAAAAAAUUUGCUACUCUUGAGGUUCUGUCAAAGAAUGUGCUGUGGCCUCUAGAAGCAUUUUUAAAAAGAGACUUUCACAAGUGAUUGUGCAAAAUUGUGAGGUCACUGAAUAGGUGUGUAUCCUCCUAAGGAGGUAGCGUUGGAGGAGCUGUUCUUGUUCAAUUUACUCAGCACCUGUGAAGAGGCUUCACUGUGAUUUGCCUGUACAGGUGUGCAGGUAAAAAUCUAAGUUCCACAGGUAGUGCAAAAAAAUCUACCUCCCUAGGUACCUCGUACAUUUAUCACAGUUUCCUGGUAAACAGUUCUGCUGUUGUUGACAAAAUUUUAUCAGAAACAUUGCAUACUCUUCUCUAAAUAGUAGUUUCCCUACAAGUGGCUGUCUUCAGUUUAGUCGUUUAAGUUAUGUUGACAUAAAUGAUUAUGUGUGUGGCAGGGGCUUUUGCGUAGGUUGUUGAAACAUUGCACCUUUUGGACUAACAGUUUUUACCAAAAUAGGCAGAAGUGACAUUUGCAGCCACAGCUGUGUGGCAUUGAGCGUCUAAGGUAUGUGUAAUAGGCAGUGUAUCGGUAGCAUUGAUACCUUGGUCAACACCAGUAAGCCAUGUAAUUGCCCAGAAGUGGGCUCUAACACUAGUUUUAGGAGAUGCAGCCAAAACGACAAAGCUGGAGGCCUCUCCCUCUGAGCUUGGCCUCCACUUGGUCAAAACAGUCCCCAGUUUGUCCCUACGGGACACAGGCCUGCCUUGUUAGGAAAUCAGCAACAUUUAGGAGCCCACAAUACCUCACAUAACUCUGUGUACAGUAACAGAGAAUGGAAAUAGGGCUGUAAGCAUGAACAACCAGUCAAGUUACAAAUAUAGAAUACUCUCUCAAUUCCACUUUAGUUAGUCAUGGAGGGACAGUGUGAGUUUUAUAAACUUAUAAGGAAUAUACAAACAGUUCCAAAUUUAAAAUAACUUGAAGUAACUUUUAAGUGUGUGAAAAGAAUAUUUUUUUCCACCCUGUCCAUUUAAGCAUCUGUGACAGGCAGUAUUAAGUGAUGGGUGUCUUUACGUACACAUGCCUGUUGCUCACAGUACUGGGGAAGAGUUGCAAAAUAGUCACCCAUUCUGCAGUGAUUUCUCUCUUCUUAUUUGUGAAAGACUCAAAAAAAAAAAAAAAAAAAAAAAAAAAAAAAACAACAACAAAAAAAAGGCCAGGCACGGUGGCUCAGACCUAUAAUCCCAGCACCUUGGGAGGCCAAGUCAGGUGGAUCACAAGGUCAGGAGAGCGAGACCAUCCUGGCUAACACGGUGAAACCAACCCCGUCUCUACUAAAAAUACAAAAAAUUAGCUGGGCGUGGUGGUGGGCGCCUAUAAUCCCAGCUACUCGGGAAGCUGAGGCAGGAGAAUUGCUUGAACCCGGGAGGUGGAGGUUGCAGUGAGCCGAAAUUGUGCCAUUGCACUCUAGCCUGGGCGCCAGAGCAAGACUCUGACUCAAAGAAAAAAAAAAUAGGGGGGAUGUGGGUUGUGAGAGCGACACUGUGUGUCCAUGCGUGAAGAAACCCGGCUCAUGAUGACCUCGCCCCAGAACGCCGAAGCAGGGCCGGUCCAGCCUGGAUUUCACAGUGUUCUUCAUUGCCUUUGUCCUUGAUUUUUUGUCGUUACCAUUAUAACUUAUCUCUCUUUCCCAAAUGUAUAAGUAGGCUUUGAAUAUGAGUUUAAAAGAAAGAAUUCGGGGAUGAUUUCAGAGUACACUAGAAUAUUUUUUAAAAGAAUAUUUUAUAAAAAUACAGUGAUAGUAAAAGAAGUAGAAGGCCAAAUUCCGCCCCCAGCCCCUUCUUAAUAUUGGACUUUAUUCCUUUGCUUUUUUCCCUUGCUGCCAUCUAAGGAGGCUUUCUGUGCUAUAGCAUCCAGUUCCUCUGCCAGGCAUUUCUGUAAAGAUGAGGCACCUUCCACUGUUUUAUUCUCCAUCAUUAGAGCACGUGUCCUGCUGACUCGGAGCAGAGGGGAGGCACACGGGGGUGAACAUUCCCUGACAGAUUGGAUGUCUCUUAACUCUUUUUUCCUGGUAUCAAAGAAUGGCACAAUUUAGUUGAUUUGAUAGCGUUACCAAAUCGUUUUUCCUUUAGAAUGAAUCUAGAAUGCAGAUAGAUUCUGAGGUCCAGAUGGGCCUCUCUCCACCAACCUGUGACCAGUGUACCUGUGAUUUUAUCACUGCACAUUCAUAGAAAGGUUACAGGGCUAAUCUUCCCGUGAUAUGAAUCAUGAAAGUCAAAAUUUAUGAAUGAAAAUAAAAAGGAAUGAAGUACUGAUAUAUGCCACACCAGAGAUAAAUAUUGAAAACAUUACCUAUGCUAAGUAAAAGAAGCCAGUCACAAAAGACACUACCUAUUGUCUGAUUCCAUUCAUGUAAAAUAUCCAGAAUAGGCAAAUCUAUAGCGACGAAAAGUGUAAUAGUGAUUGCCUGGGAAAGGGGCGUGGGAAGCAUGGCUAACGGGUAUUGGGUUUUUCUUUGGGGUGAUGAAAAUAUUGUUAAGAUUAAUUGUGGUGGUGUUUGUACAACUCUCUAAAUAUACUAAAAGCUACCAAAUUGUACACUCUAAAUGGGUGAGUUAUAGGGUAUGUGAAUUAGAUCUCAAUAAAGCUAUUGUAAAAAAUGUGUGAAGGAAGGGGAAGCAUCCUAUAACCUAUACCAUCCCAACAGCCCAGCUAGAGGACGAUUCCUGAGCCUCCUUCUCAGCCUUUGUGUUAAUUCUUUGCAUUGAUGACUUCUCUCUCUUUACCCUUACUAAUUAGCUCUCAAAACCUCUAUUUAAUAAUGAUGCUAUUUAUAACUUUCCUCCUUCUGGUUUCUUGCUUGCCCUUUUUGUGGUGUUUGCUUGUUUUUCUUUUUUCUCAAUACUCUGCCCAGCGUUGCGUGUUGGUUCCGGAGACUUAAGUGAUCCAGUGGGCACUGUCAGGCAAUUAUUUCUUUUGCUCAUUAAUUAAGUGUUCACAGAUACAUUCAGCAGCCAAACCUUGUGGCAUGCCUUCUGUCCCAGACAGUGAGAAUCUACUUGGAACUUGGAUAUUUCUGUGAGCCUUGAUUAUAUACACCACCAAGGGGAUGGCAUAGAACUAAGUUUUUUCUUCUUCUCCACAACAGACUUUGUUCUUUAAUUUCACAAGCUUGACAUAGCCUAUAAGACAUCAUAGUGGUACCAUAGACAGUUUUCCCUUGAUGCCCAUGGGGGAUUUGUUCUGGGACCUCCCACAGAUACCAAAAUCCACAGGUUUAUCAGCAAGGGUCACUGCUCAAUUGCAACAACUGAAGCAGAAGCUCCUCUCAUCAGAGGCAGUUACUGCAGCAUGUUCUGUAGGGCAAAUAUAACCAUAUGUAAGUGACUGUGCUAUCAGGAGACAGAACAACAAGACCCAGAAAGACUCAGUGACCCACAGAGCCAGUUCCACCCAAACAAGUCUUAGUAAUGAGAUUAGAUAAUGAGAGUGUAUUUUCUUCAUCAAUUCAUGUAGCUCAGCAAGGCUGGAAACUGCUUGCACACUUCUGCAGAGAAAAAAAAAAGUUCCAUUUGCUGGAACUCAAUAAAUAAAGAAGGCCUUAGUGGGUACGUGUUAUCUCCUUAGCAUCACCUGGAUGCCUGACCCUUUUCCAGAGUGUCAUGUUGCCUGGGUUUUGUCCUUCAGUCUAAGUGAUACACCUCUUAGUGUGGCGGAGAAAAGGGUGCUGUAUUUCUUCCUGAUGGAUACAUGCUUAAAUGGAAAAGUAGCAUGAGAUGAACUCCCAUAGCCCCUUCCUUUUAUUAUUUUUAAAAUAUUCAUUCAUUUAUUUAUUUAUUUUUGAGAUGGAGUCUCACUCUGUCACCCAGGCUGGAGCGCAGUGGCGCGAUCUCAGCUCACUGCAACCUCCGCCUCCCGGGUUCAAGCAAUUCUCCUGCCUCGGCCUCCCGAGUAGCUAGGACUACAGGUGUGCCCACCACCACACCUAGCUAAUUUUUGUAUUUUUAGUAGAGAUCGGCUUUCACCAUGUUGACCAGGCUGGUCUUGAACUCUUGACCUCAGGUGAUCCACCCGUCUCGGCCUUCCAAAGUGCUGGGAUUACAGGCGUGAGCCACUGUGCCUGGCCGGCCCUUCCUUUUAGACAAUAGAAACAUGCUGCAACCACAUACCACCAUAAACACGGUGGGGGAAGAGGCUGCAAUCAACAGUCAGGAGGAUCUGGGUUCCAAGCCCAGGUUUGCAGUGUAACAGCUGUGUGCUCUUGGUGUGAACAUUUGGUCAUGUACAAAUGAGGAUAAUGAUACUGCCCCCUUGUGAUCAUUAGGGGGAUUAAAUUAAAUGCAGAAAUAUAUGUGAGAUGCUUAAUGUGUUGUAAGGCGCAUGGAAUAUAUUUAGUGAAUAUUAACUGUAUAUUAAUACAAAGUCCUGUAUUCAGAAUCUCCAGUAUAAAUUACAUUUAUAUAGUAGAGAUAUGAAUAGUUUUUGUGAACAAGAAGACCUGGAACUUCAGGUGACUAGAAGCUCAGAGUGAGCCAGCUAUGUUUGAUGAUAGUUAUUCUUAAGAUCACACAGAGAAACGGCAAGCAAGCUGCUUUGGGCAAAAAAGAGCAUUUCUACACUGUUCAGACUGCCUCUGUACUGUUAGAAUAGGUCUAGGGCGUGUUGCGUGAGUGGUGACUGAGUAAGAUGUUCAGAGGGAAGCCGUGACCGUCAUCUUGGAAUAUUGUUUGAAAGUCUGACCUGUACAAAGCAGCACUCACUUCCCCUGCGUGUCAGACACCUGCAUGAGGGCUGGGGAGGGUCCAGUACAGGAAAGCGCAUUUUUAAUAUGUGUAUGGAGGAAGUUCGUCAAGAUGGGUGCCAUCUGGCAGUGGAGUAGCACUUCCUGGAAAGUAAUGAGCUCCCUUGGACUUUGUUUGAAGAGUCACCCAGGUUUUUGUAAAGAAGUGUUUCAGAUCAGUAUGCAAUGGAUGACUGUAAAUUUCUCUUCAGAUCUAAGAAUCUGUGAUUGGAUGAAAGGGAGAAAGGACUGCAUAAGUGCUUGUUGCUUGUAAACUGGGCCAGGUGGAUGUCAUGGCCCUAGGAGCUUCUUGCCUGCCUUUGCAUGCCAUAAAGCAGUCCUGCAACCCAGUGUCACCUCAGAGGGAUGGGAAUGUAGAAGAAGAGAGUGAAUAGGGACAGUGAUGAGGGGUGAAAAUAUGUAACUCCUUGCCCCUUCUGUAUACCCUAGUACAUUAGGAAGUUCACCCUUGUCUAGGCUUCCUGUUAGGAAGACAGCAGACUCAAAAUGGAGUCUCAACCCCUUUCAAAGACUGCAAGAUCUCCUUGUACACACUGGACUUGGGAGAAAAUGAGAGCUUUCAGGCCUGCUAUCUUAACAGGUUCAGAAAGGUGUGGUCCAGCCCCCUGACUAACCAGCCCUGCUGUGCACACUGAGAAUUCUGCUCAGGUGUACCUUUCUGUGUGCUCCUGGGUGCACCCCCAAAGUGCUGGUUCUCUUGAAAACCUUUUUAUUUAGGUUCAGACAGACAAACUGUGGUAUCUUCCAUUCUGACCAUAAAGUGUUUCUUCUGGGUCUAACUACUAUAGUGGGAUAUUUUCUCUAGAACAAGAGGUUGUUUCUUUUUGGCAUUGAGAAAUGUUGCCGAUGUGAUUUUCUUUUGUGAACGUUUAAGACACAGCGCUUGCCACUUGAACUUUCUUUUGCCGUGCGUAGCUGAUUCCACAUAAUGGCUGCAGCUCCAGGCAGAAACCUGUUUGGAAGUUGUUUUAAACUCUUCCUGGAAUCUCUAGGCAGUGGCUCAGUGGGGUUUUUUUCCAACCAUUCCUUAGGAUGACCAGAAGCUUGACAGAAUCCUCUUGUCUUCAUUUUGAGAAAAUAUGUCUUUACUGUGUGUAUGUGCAGCAUUUGGUUUUACCUCGUGGGUCUAAGCAUUUUCAACUAAGCUUCCUUUUCCAACCUAGCAGACUUGUUUAAAGAACUUCAAACUAAUAGCCAAGCUGUAAUACGGUGGCUCUCUCAGCCUGAGAAGCCUGUGCUCACCGUCACUCUCUUCUUCCCUGGGGUGAUAGGGAUGGGGAGUAGUGUGUGUGAGAGGACAGAAGCGAGGAUUGAUUGAAGAUUAUUUUACGAGGCGAGAGCAUGGUGGCACACCUGUCAGCUGAGUGGACUCAGCGCCUGCCCCGGCUAGGCUGUCCUCCUCCUGUGCCAGCCGUGGGUUCCCUGAGUCCCUCUGCAGUCAUUCAUGGGUGCUGAAAAUAAAGAUACCCUUUCUGUCGAAAGUGUUCGCCGGGCUGCCUCUGCCUCCCUGGAAAAGCAGCAGGGCACACAGGCUUCCUAGGCAGCCCCUGAGGGAGGGGCUCUUUUUAUUGUCACUCUGGUUAGUUUGAAGACCAGACAGAAGGCAGCAAAAACCAACCCUUUGUUGAAAACUCUUUGCCUUUAGGCCCUUGGUACCAUGUUCAUGAGGCUCCAGAUAAUUCCACAAAUACAUUAUUAUUGUUACCUAGACUUGGGGACAGAGAAGGGUGAAACAUGGGUCUGGGAAUUCACAGAUGAAUAUACUGUAAUCCCCUCGAGCACAUUUCUUUUAAAGGAAUGGGGGUAUUCUAAAGGAGUGAACACUCCACUGGGGGGCUGCUAGGCCCCUGUGAACGGUGGCAGCCUUGGCCACGGUGUGUGCUGUGAUCUCUCCUGGGUCCCCCGGGCAUCCUCAGACCUCCCCCACACCCAACCCACAGUCCCUUCUCCAUCCAUCUGCUGACCACACCCCAGGAUGUUUCCAGCUCAGAUCACGCCUGAUUGCAUCCACACAAACUGCACGCCAGGCAUUUCCGUUUGGAUGUGUACACAAAAACAACACGUCCCAGACUGAGCUGAUCUUUCUGUACCCCUCAAAAGAAAAGUUCUGUACCCGGCCAGGCCUGGUGGCUCACACCUGUAAUCCCAGCACUUUGGGAGGCCAAGGCAGGAGGAUCACGAGGUCAGGAGAUUGAGACCAUCCUGGGUAACACGGUGAAACCCUGUCUCUGCUAAAAAUACAAAAAAUUAGCUGGGCAUGGUGGCGGGCGCCUGUAGUCCCAGCUACAGGAGAAUGGCAAGAAUCCGGAAGGCAAAGCUGGAGCUUGCAGUGAGCUGAGAUUGAGCCACUGCACUCCAGCCUGGUGACAGAGUGACACUCCGUCUCAAAAAAAAAAAAAAAAAAAAAGAAAUUCUGUACCCUUCCAGAUGGUCCUGGACAUAUCUUGAAUCUACCCUGCUUUUCCUCAUCUGCACUGCUGUCCUCUUGAUCUGGGCUACUGAGGCUAGAAUGCACAUCUGAUCAUGUGCCUCCUGCUUAAAAUAGUAUUUUUCCUCUUAAGAGUAGUCCAAACUCCUAUUGCUGGAUUAAAAGGCUGUUCCAGGCUCUCCCUACCUCAGGGCACACCAUCUUUCCUCCCAGUCUCCCCUCCCCUCUGUCUCCAGUGCUUCCAUCCUUCAGUCAUGCUGAGGUUGUCUUUGUUACCUUUGCUUCUCUUGGCCCGCACUCUCUGUUGGCUCUGCCAGCAUCCCUAUGCACCUGCUAGCUCCUACUCACUUGUCCAGCUUUGGCCUGGAAGUCCCUUCCCCUGGCAGGCAGCCCUAAGCUACCCUUUGCUUGCUACUGGCUCAUAUUCUCACUGCUUGUCCUCAGGCUGUGAGCCCUGGGAGGGCUGGGCUGAGUCCCCGAACCUGCCACGUCUAUAGGGUGUAACCUACCUGAGGCCUGACUGCUAAAAUCAAAAGAAGCCUUUCUCAUUUGCUUAGCUGAGCUAAGUCCUUUCUGGAGAAGAAUGCCCACGUCCUGGGUGGACUUCUGUUCGGCCUGGGGCAGGACGCUGCAUGUCAGUUCACCUAGAGCCCCUCGCUUGCCCUCACCCCUCUCCCUUUCCUUCUCCUCCCCGUGUUGUCUCAUGGUCAGUUCCUCUCCUGGCAAGGCAAGAGAAUCAUAAAAUCUCUUUGGACCAUGUGUCUCUCUGAUGCACUUUGGAGGUUGAAGCUCACUUUCGUGAAGUUAGGAGCGGUUAAUCCUCCUGCACGAGGAUGCAUGCCUGCUAGGGAAAGCCUCCCUGCGUUUAUAUGGAACAGUGGUGUGUACCUUAGGGCAACCCAGAAACAGCUGAGAUGGCCCUAAACUCUUCCGUAUUUUGAUUCAGAAGCUUUACCUUAUUUGAACAUCUGCAGAAUAAGUUCUUUCCUUUAGAAAUGAUUGGGGAUAAAAUUGUUUGCAUUAUGAAAUAUUGUAUGGCCAGGUGGCCCCUCUUUCAUGUUUUGUUCCUUGUGAAGAGGUUGAGUCUCCUAUUUUUUUUUUUUUUUUGGAGAUAGAGUUUUGUUCUUGUCCCUCAGGCUGGAGUAAAAUGGUGCAAUCUUGGCUCACUGCAACCUCCGCCUCCUGGGUUCAAACGAUUCUCCUGCCUCAGCCUCCCAAGUAGCUGGGAUCACAGGCACGUGCCACCACACCUGGCUAAUUUUUGUAUUUUUAGUAAGAGAUGGGGUUUCGCCAUGUUGGGCAGGCUGGUCUUGAACUCCUGACCUCAGUUGAUCUGCCCGCCUCGGCCUCCCAAAGUGCUGGGAUCACAGGCGUGAGCCACCACGCCCAGCCUAUGGUAUGCUUUUAAAAAUGGUUUCUCUGCACUAAUGAUUAUUUAAAAAAAAAACUCUGGCAAGAACAAAAACAAAUGGUUUUUUAAAAACUCUAGAAAUAAUUUGAUACAUUCGAGGACUCUGGAGAGGGAGAGAGUUAAAGGCUGAUGUGUGUGACUCUUUUUCCUCUCCCCCCAAGGAAAAAAAAUGAAGAGAAGGAGCUUUUAAGUGCAGUGCCUCGUUUUUAUGUGAUUGCAAACCUGAACCAAUCCUUUUAGUGGUGGAUGUGGGACAUGUUAGCUUUUCCAACAGUUUAGAUGGGCCUUUGUUUUUAUUGUUGGUCACUGUAAGAAUUCCAAGGAAUAGAAGGAUCUCAUGGGCAAAAUCAGUUUGCUUUUUUCUCUGUAUAUUUGUUAGUUUAUAGCAGCUUCUAUUUUCCUCCUAUUUUUAAAAGCUGAAAUGCCUUUAAUCGCACUCAGUGUGUUUAUUCAUGGAAGCCAGAGAAGAGGGUCCCUUCCUUUCCCCCAUAGCGCCGUAAUUGGAAAUUUGGUAGUACUAGGUGAAAUUCUCAGUUUUGGCGCUCGCAUGGAACAGCCAUCCAUCUGCUGGCGAGACACACUGCCCGGGGCUUUUCAAGAAAUCCCUUAAUGGUCCUGAACACUAAUAAUAUUUAUAUACAUUGAGAUGAGACAAAAUUUACAGCGGGCUCUGGGGCUGGCUCCAGGACUCUCUAAUCCCACACUUGCUCACGUUCUCUUGCUUGCCUCCUAGAAUCCUUUCAGGUUGUGCUUCAGUGAGGGGAGCAUGGUGUCCGUCUCUGCAGCAAUGCUUAUUUAUGCAGUUCGUCCUCUAACAAACAGAGCAACUUUCCUUUUGACCUUCCCCUCUUCUCCCCAUCACAUUCCAUUGCUGCCCCCGCAUAGAGCAUGUGCUUAUGCAUAGUUUGCAUCAUUUAACACGAAGGAACCCCUUGAUUUGUGAUCCCUUUAAGAAGUUGCUCUGUAUAUAAAGAAAAUGAUUUUUCCUGGUUGGUUUUACUGAAGUUCCUUCAGAAAUAGCUCCCACCACCGAAACACACCUGACUUCCCCAGCCUGUGUAUCGGUUGUGGCACGGACUGACUGACUGGAUGGUAUAAUUUCACUCACUCCUUUGGGAAGUUUCGGGGGACUACUGCUCAGAUGUGUGGGAAAUGCGGAAUAUAUCUACAGGUACUUUGUCAGUUUUUUUUUUUCUUUUCUUUCUCAUCCUGGAAAAUCCCGGCAUUGAUAUUUAGGUAUAACUAUUUGCAAGCAAGUGCAGAGGGACAUUUUUCUGUUCUUUUCAACGUUCUUAUUACUACUGCAUUAAUAGCUACUUGAUCUUAAUGUCUAUUACACAUCAUUUUAUAUAAUGUUUUCUUUAAAUUGUCAGGGAAAGGGAUUCUGCAAGUAGAUGUUGGUCCCCCCAGUUAGUGUCUGAUGAUGAUGGUAAGAUUCUCAGAGUUUCCUUCCUCUAAUGACAAAGCAUGGUGAUGGUGAUGUCUGAAGAGCAGCCUCGGUGCUCCAAGAUGGGUGUAUGCUUAAUACUGCUGGCACACGCCUGACGAGCGGGAAUGUGAGCGUUGUUUCUGUAACCAGUUUUACUGAACCUCACAGAUCCAUUAUACGACGUGAAUUUUGUGGGAAUAACAUAGGCUGGGAGUCUGCUCUCUUCCAGCCUGGUCCCUCUCUUCUUUCAGCCCUACCCUCUCUGAUCAUCAUGUCCCUUGCACUGCGGCCAGGUAACCUUUCUGAUACGAAGGUCUGGGCAUGUUGUUCCCUUGCCUAAAACUUUCCAUGGUUUCGUAUUAUCCACAGUUGGGCUAAACCCUCUGGGACAGGCCUUCAGUGCCUCCCCGGGCAGUGGUCCCUGGCCUUCUUCAGUAACACCCAAGCCCUUGCACCCACAGUGACCUCGUUGCUUUUACAAGCAUUUACAUGUGAUGUUCUUUAUUCCUCCCUUGCUCAUCUUUCCACUUUCAACUCCACAAAACCGUCCUCGGCACCCAGAAGCCCAGGAAACACCAGGCAGCUCCACUCACUCCCGUACUUGCUGUGUCGUCCGUUCCCUGGGGACAGGAUUGUCGCUGAUCCUGCGUGCAUCUGUCUGGCACACAGGUGCAGCACACAUUAAAUAGCUGCUAAAUGAAUAAAUGAAGAAUAGAUGGAAUUAUAUUCUGUUGUGACCAGUUUAAAAACAUGAAAUUGGAAUACCCAAUUGCAGUGUUUCUUUAGAUCUUGGACCUUGAGGUGACCUCUGUAAUGGAUAUAUUUGAAAUUAUUAACUGUCUUCAAGUGGGGGUUUGAUGAGAGAGAGAGAGAGUGUGUGUGUGUGUGUGUGUGUGUGUGUUUACAGAAAAUAUGCUAGGUUUGUACAUUCAAAUUUGUGUUAUCCUCUUCAAGAAAGUCACCUUGGUAGACAGCAUAUAUAUCCCAACAUUUUAGGAACUCAUAAAAUGCAUACUUUUUUGGUGUGAUCAGAGAUGGGUAACUCCUUAUUACUUGUGGGUUAGAUUAGUUUUUGGAAAUAGCCUGGAGUCAUUGAGAGCCAAUCCUUAUCAACAAAAUGGCAUAAAUGGACAGGAAUGGGUUUCUUCUUCACUUUAGAGAUAGCUCUGAAGACAUGUCUCAGUUGGGAUUAGUUCAGUUGCAUAUAUGAAUAGCAGUCAUUGAAACAAGAUAAAAGUGUAUGUCUCUCACAUCUAAAGAAGUCUGGAGUAAGCAGUCCAGGGUUAGCCUAGCGGCCCCACUCUCAUAAGGGACUAAGUUCCUUUUAUCUCGCUUCACCAUUCUUGAUGUUUCGCCUUGUGGUCCAAGGUUGGUACUUGAGCUCCAAGCAUUACUACUGCAUUCCAGCCAGCAAGGAGGAGGAUGGCCAUGCCCUCUUUGUUCUCAGGAGUCUUCCAGGAAGUUCCAGUCACAACGUUUGUUUAUAUCUCACUGGCCAGAACUUAAGUCAUAUGGCCACCUCUAGCUACAAGGAAGGCUGGGAGAUGUAGUCUGUAACUGGAUGGCCAUAUUAUCAACUAAAAAUUACUGAAAAUGACAAGAAGAAUAAAUAAUGGAAGGCAACCUGUUGUUUCUGUCAAAGGAUGACUUCAAAAGAGAAAGUUGCAAAAGUAUUUCAAGCUUGACAGUAUCAUGACAGUUUUCUUCAGAGGUGACGCUAUUCAUUUGCAUGUCCAAGUUCUGAUAUCUGUUUUCAAGUUCACCUAUUUGCAGCGAAAUAGGAACUCUUGGAGGCAACUAGUGGGUGUGUAAACCGGUACAAACUUUCUAGAGGACAGUUUAACCCAACAAGAUGAAUUCUGGAAAUUGAUCCUAAUGAAAUGUUAAGGGUGCUCAUGAAGAUUGCUUUGCCGAUUGCAAUAAUAAAAAGUAAAGAAAAUAUCUUAUAAUUGGGGACAGGUGUAACUUAUGAUACAUUCCACAAUGGAGUGUAAUACUGCUGUUAAAUGUUUGUGGAAUUCACAAUCUUUUAUGCCAAAAGAAAGCUUUCAGAAUGGCUUGUCUUUUUUGUAGAUACUUGUAUUUAUAUGUCCAUGCACAUACAUAAGAAAGGACCAGGGAAGGUCUGCUUGAAGAUAUUAAUAAAGGGGUCACUUGUGGGUAGGUGGACUUACUUGUUCUCUAUAUUCUCUUUACUUGUUUGUGAUCUCUGGUUUUUUUAAUCAUGUAUUUUUAUUACAAGAAAAAACAAAUUCUAGAAUCUCCACUCAAUAUUGCAUGUCAGAGUCAAAAAGAUACACAUUUAAAUAAUUUUGUAUUGUUUUCCAAUUUGAGGAUAAAGUAGGAAAUGUAUAAUGCAAACCAGAUUUCAUAUUUUGUUGAUUUAGACUUAAUUUACAAGUAAGGCUGACAGCCCACAGAGUGUGAUCACGACAGCAUUGUUAUGGAAAUAAAUGCCAGCUCAUGCAUUUGGGAUGUACACCAUGGAUCUGUGGUUAUUAGAUACUGAUUUCACUUUAGCACACGAAGAGGCUUAGCGGAGGUGGCUUCUAAUAUCCUAUGGUUCUGUGGGCUCGGAGAUGCUACUCACCCACUUGUCAGAGGCAUUGAAACCAGAGCAACUGCAUCUUGAAUAGGAGCUAGGUAAAAUGAGGCCGAAUUCCCAGACAGUUAAGACAUUCUGAGUCACAGGAUGAGGUUAAAGGUCAGCACAAAAUACAGGUCAUAAAGACCUUGCUGAUCUAGCAGAUGCAGUUAAAGAAGCCGGCGCAAACCCACCAAAACCAAGAUGGUAACGAGAGUGACCUGUGAUCGUCCUCACUGCUGCACUCCCACCAGCGCCAUGAGUGUUUACAUGUCAUAGCAACAUCAGGAAGUUACCCUAUAUGGUCUAAAAUGGAGAGUGUGCCCAAGCACGUGUGGGAAGCGGGCGUGCACCGAGAACAAUGAGUGCUGCCACCCCGAGUGCCUGGGCAGCUGCAGCGCGCCUGACAACGACACGGCCUGUGUAGCUUGCCGCCACUACUACUAUGCCGGUGUCUGUGUGCCUGCCUGCCCGCCCAACACCUACAGGUUUGAGGGCUGGCGCUGUGUGGACCGUGACUUCUGCGCCAACAUCCUCAGCGCCGAGAGCAGCGACUCCGAGGGGUUUGUGAUCCACGACGGCGAGUGCAUGCAGGAGUGCCCCUCGGGCUUCAUCCGCAACGGCAGCCAGAGCAUGUACUGCAUCCCUUGUGAAGGUCCUUGCCCGAAGGUCUGUGAGGAAGAAAAGAAAACAAAGACCAUUGAUUCUGUUACUUCUGCUCAGAUGCUCCAAGGAUGCACCAUCUUCAAGGGCAAUUUGCUCAUUAACAUCCGACGGGGGAAUAACAUUGCUUCAGAGCUGGAGAACUUCAUGGGGCUCAUCGAGGUGGUGACGGGCUACGUGAAGAUCCGCCAUUCUCAUGCCUUGGUCUCCUUGUCCUUCCUAAAAAACCUUCGCCUCAUCCUAGGAGAGGAGCAGCUAGAAGGGAAUUACUCCUUCUACGUCCUCGACAACCAGAACUUGCAGCAACUGUGGGACUGGGACCACCGCAACCUGACCAUCAAAGCAGGGAAAAUGUACUUUGCUUUCAAUCCCAAAUUAUGUGUUUCCGAAAUUUACCGCAUGGAGGAAGUGACGGGGACUAAAGGGCGCCAAAGCAAAGGGGACAUAAACACCAGGAACAACGGGGAGAGAGCCUCCUGUGAAAGUGACGUCCUGCAUUUCACCUCCACCACCACGUCGAAGAAUCGCAUCAUCAUAACCUGGCACCGGUACCGGCCCCCUGACUACAGGGAUCUCAUCAGCUUCACCGUUUACUACAAGGAAGCACCCUUUAAGAAUGUCACAGAGUAUGAUGGGCAGGAUGCCUGCGGCUCCAACAGCUGGAACAUGGUGGACGUGGACCUCCCGCCCAACAAGGACGUGGAGCCCGGCAUCUUACUACAUGGGCUGAAGCCCUGGACUCAGUACGCCGUUUACGUCAAGGCUGUGACCCUCACCAUGGUGGAGAACGACCAUAUCCGUGGGGCCAAGAGUGAGAUCUUGUACAUUCGCACCAAUGCUUCAGUUCCUUCCAUUCCCUUGGACGUUCUUUCAGCAUCGAACUCCUCUUCUCAGUUAAUCGUGAAGUGGAACCCUCCCUCUCUGCCCAACGGCAACCUGAGUUACUACAUUGUGCGCUGGCAGCGGCAGCCUCAGGACGGCUACCUUUACCGGCACAAUUACUGCUCCAAAGACAAAAUCCCCAUCAGGAAGUAUGCCGACGGCACCAUCGACAUUGAGGAGGUCACAGAGAACCCCAAGACUGAGGUGUGUGGUGGGGAGAAAGGGCCUUGCUGCGCCUGCCCCAAAACUGAAGCCGAGAAGCAGGCCGAGAAGGAGGAGGCUGAAUACCGCAAAGUCUUUGAGAAUUUCCUGCACAACUCCAUCUUCGUGCCCAGACCUGAAAGGAAGCGGAGAGAUGUCAUGCAAGUGGCCAACACCACCAUGUCCAGCCGAAGCAGGAACACCACGGCCGCAGACACCUACAACAUCACCGACCCGGAAGAGCUGGAGACAGAGUACCCUUUCUUUGAGAGCAGAGUGGAUAACAAGGAGAGAACUGUCAUUUCUAACCUUCGGCCUUUCACAUUGUACCGCAUCGAUAUCCACAGCUGCAACCACGAGGCUGAGAAGCUGGGCUGCAGCGCCUCCAACUUCGUCUUUGCAAGGACUAUGCCCGCAGAAGGAGCAGAUGACAUUCCUGGGCCAGUGACCUGGGAGCCAAGGCCUGAAAACUCCAUCUUUUUAAAGUGGCCGGAACCUGAGAAUCCCAAUGGAUUGAUUCUAAUGUAUGAAAUAAAAUACGGAUCACAAGUUGAGGAUCAGCGAGAAUGUGUGUCCAGACAGGAAUACAGGAAGUAUGGAGGGGCCAAGCUAAACCGGCUAAACCCGGGGAACUACACAGCCCGGAUUCAGGCCACAUCUCUCUCUGGGAAUGGGUCGUGGACAGAUCCUGUGUUCUUCUAUGUCCAGGCCAAAACAGGAUAUGAAAACUUCAUCCAUCUGAUCAUCGCUCUGCCCGUCGCUGUCCUGUUGAUCGUGGGAGGGUUGGUGAUUAUGCUGUACGUCUUCCAUAGAAAGAGAAAUAACAGCAGGCUGGGGAAUGGAGUGCUGUAUGCCUCUGUGAACCCGGAGUACUUCAGCGCUGCUGAUGUGUACGUUCCUGAUGAGUGGGAGGUGGCUCGGGAGAAGAUCACCAUGAGCCGGGAACUUGGGCAGGGGUCGUUUGGGAUGGUCUAUGAAGGAGUUGCCAAGGGUGUGGUGAAAGAUGAACCUGAAACCAGAGUGGCCAUUAAAACAGUGAACGAGGCCGCAAGCAUGCGUGAGAGGAUUGAGUUUCUCAACGAAGCUUCUGUGAUGAAGGAGUUCAAUUGUCACCAUGUGGUGCGAUUGCUGGGUGUGGUGUCCCAAGGCCAGCCAACACUGGUCAUCAUGGAACUGAUGACACGGGGCGAUCUCAAAAGUUAUCUCCGGUCUCUGAGGCCAGAAAUGGAGAAUAAUCCAGUCCUAGCACCUCCAAGCCUGAGCAAGAUGAUUCAGAUGGCCGGAGAGAUUGCAGACGGCAUGGCAUACCUCAACGCCAAUAAGUUCGUCCACAGAGACCUUGCUGCCCGGAAUUGCAUGGUAGCCGAAGAUUUCACAGUCAAAAUCGGAGAUUUUGGUAUGACGCGAGAUAUCUAUGAGACAGACUAUUACCGGAAAGGAGGGAAAGGGCUGCUGCCCGUGCGCUGGAUGUCUCCUGAGUCCCUCAAGGAUGGAGUCUUCACCACUUACUCGGACGUCUGGUCCUUCGGGGUCGUCCUCUGGGAGAUCGCCACACUGGCCGAGCAGCCCUACCAGGGCUUGUCCAACGAGCAAGUCCUUCGCUUCGUCAUGGAGGGCGGCCUUCUGGACAAGCCAGACAACUGUCCUGACAUGCUGUUUGAACUGAUGCGCAUGUGCUGGCAGUAUAACCCCAAGAUGAGGCCUUCCUUCCUGGAGAUCAUCAGCAGCAUCAAAGAGGAGAUGGAGCCUGGCUUCCGGGAGGUCUCCUUCUACUACAGCGAGGAGAACAAGCUGCCCGAGCCGGAGGAGCUGGACCUGGAGCCAGAGAACAUGGAGAGCGUCCCCCUGGACCCCUCGGCCUCCUCGUCCUCCCUGCCACUGCCCGACAGACACUCAGGACACAAGGCCGAGAACGGCCCCGGCCCUGGGGUGCUGGUCCUCCGCGCCAGCUUCGACGAGAGACAGCCUUACGCCCACAUGAACGGGGGCCGCAAGAACGAGCGGGCCUUGCCGCUGCCCCAGUCUUCGACCUGCUGAUCCUUGGAUCCUGAAUCUGUGCAAACAGUAACGUGUGCGCACGCGCAGCGGGGUGGGGGGGGAGAGAGAGUUUUAACAAUCCAUUCACAAGCCUCCUGUACCUCAGUGGAUCUUCAGAACUGCCCUUGCUGCCCGCGGGAGACAGCUUCUCUGCAGUAAAACACAUUUGGGAUGUUCCUUUUUUCAAUAUGCAAGCAGCUUUUUAUUCCCUGCCCAAACCCUUAACUGACAUGGGCCUUUAAGAACCUUAAUGACAACACUUAAUAGCAACAGAGCACUUGAGAACCAGUCUCCUCACUCUGUCCCUGUCCUUCCCUGUUCUCCCUUUCUCUCUCCUCUCUGCUUCAUAACGGAAAAAUAAUUGCCACAAGUCCAGCUGGGAAGCCCUUUUUAUCAGUUUGAGGAAGUGGCUGUCCCUGUGGCCCCAUCCAACCACUGUACACACCCGCCUGACACCGUGGGUCAUUACAAAAAAACACGUGGAGAUGGAAAUUUUUACCUUUAUCUUUCACCUUUCUAGGGACAUGAAAUUUACAAAGGGCCAUCGUUCAUCCAAGGCUGUUACCAUUUUAACGCUGCCUAAUUUUGCCAAAAUCCUGAACUUUCUCCCUCAUCGGCCCGGCGCUGAUUCCUCGUGUCCGGAGGCAUGGGUGAGCAUGGCAGCUGGUUGCUCCAUUUGAGAGACACGCUGGCGACACACUCCGUCCAUCCGACUGCCCCUGCUGUGCUGCUCAAGGCCACAGGCACACAGGUCUCAUUGCUUCUGACUAGAUUAUUAUUUGGGGGAACUGGACACAAUAGGUCUUUCUCUCAGUGAAGGUGGGGAGAAGCUGAACCGGCUUCCCUGCCCUGCCUCCCCAGCCCCCUGCCCAACCCCCAAGAAUCUGGUGGCCAUGGGCCCCGAAGCAGCCUGGCGGACAGGCUUGGAGUCAAGGGGCCCCAUGCCUGCUUCUCUCCCAGCCCCAGCUCCCCCGCCCGCCCCCAAGGACACAGAUGGGAAGGGGUUUCCAGGGACUCAGCCCCACUGUUGAUGCAGGUUUGCAAGGAAAGAAAUUCAAACACCACAACAGCAGUAAGAAGAAAAGCAGUCAAUGGAUUCAAGCAUUCUAAGCUUUGUUGACAUUUUCUCUGUUCCUAGGACUUCUUCAUGGGUCUUACAGUUCUAUGUUAGACCAUGAAACAUUUGCAUACACAUCGUCUUUAAUGUCACUUUUAUAACUUUUUUACGGUUCAGAUAUUCAUCUAUACGUCUGUACAGAAAAAAAAAAGCUGCUAUUUUUUUUGUUCUUGAUCUUUGUGGAUUUAAUCUAUGAAAACCUUCAGGUCCACCCUCUCCCCUUUCUGCUCACUCCAAGAAACUUCUUAUGCUUUGUACUAGAGUGCGUGACUUUCUUCCUCUUUUCCCGGUAAUGGAUACUUCUAUCACAUAAUUUGCCAUGAACUGUUGGAUGCCUUUUUAUAAAUACAUCCCCCAUCCCUGCUCCCACCUGCCCCUUUAGUUGUUUUCUAACCCGUAGGCUCUCUGGGCACGAGGCAGAAAGCAGGCCGGGCACCCAUCCUGAGAGGGCCGCGCUCCUCUCCCCAGCCUGCCCUCACAGCAUUGGAGCCUGUUACAGUGCAAGACAUGAUACAAACUCAGGUCAGAAAAACAAAGGUUAAAUAUUUCACACGUCUUUGUUCAGUGUUUCCACUCACCGUGGUUGAGAAGCCUCACCCUCUCUUUCCCUUGCCUUUGCUUAGGUUGUGACACACAUAUAUAUAUAUUUUUUUAAUUCUUGGGUACAACAGCAGUGUUAACCGCAGACACUAGGCAUUUGGAUUACUAUUUUUCUUAAUGGCUAUUUAAUCCUUCCAUCCCACGAAAAACAGCUGCUGAGUCCAAGGGAGCAGCAGAGCGUGGUCCGGCAGGGCCUGUUGUGGCCCUCGCCACCCCCCUCACCGGACCGACUGACCUGUCUUUGGAACCAGAACAUCCCAAGGGAACUCCUUCGCACUGGCGUUGAGUGGGACCCCGGGAUCCAGGCUGGCCCAGGGCGGCACCCUCAGGGCUGUGCCCGCUGGAGUGCUAGGUGGAGGCAGCACAGACGCCACGGUGGCCCAAGAGCCCCUUUGCUUCUUGCUGGGGGACCAGGGCUGUGGUGCUGGCCCACUUUCCCUCGGCCAGGAAUCCAGGUCCUUGGGGCCCAGGGGUCUUGUCUUGUUUCAUUUUUAGCACUUCUCACCAGAGAGAUGACAGCACAAGAGUUGCUUCUGGGAUAGAAAUGUUUAGGAGUAAGAACAAAGCUGGGAUACGGUGAUUGCUAGUUGUGACUGAAGAUUCAACACAGAAAAGAAAGUUUAUACGGCUUUUUUGCUGGUCAGCAGUUUGUCCCACUGCUUUCUCUAGUCUCUAUCCCAUAGCGUGUUCCCUUUAAAAAAAAAAAAAAGGUAUUAUAUGUAGGAGUUUUCUUUUAAUUUAUUUUGUGAUAAAUUACCAGUUUCAAUCACUGUAGAAAAGCCCCAUUAUGAAUUUAAAUUUCAAGGAAAGGGUGUGUGUGUGUGUAUGUGUGGGGUGUGUGUGUGUGAGAGUGAUGGGACAGUUCUUGAUUUUUUGGGUUUUUUUUCCCCCAAACAUUUAUCUACCUCACUCUUAUUUUUUAUAUGUGUAUAUAGACAAAAGAAUACAUCUCACCUUUCUCAGCACCUGACAAUAGGCCGUUGAUACUGGUAACCUCAUCCACGCCACAGGCGCCACACCCAGGUGAUGCAGGGGGAAGCCAGGCUGUAUUCCGGGGUCAAAGCAACACUAACUCACCUCUCUGCUCAUUUCAGACAGCUUGCCUUUUUCUGAGAUGUCCUGUUUUGUGUUGCUUUUUUUGUUUUGUUUUCUAUCUUGGUUUCCACCAAGGUGUUAGAUUUCUCCUCCUCCUAGCCAGGUGGCCCUGUGAGGCCAACGAGGGCACCAGAGCACACCUGGGGGAGCCACCAGGCUGUCCCUGGCUGGUUGUCUUUGGAACAAACUGCUUCUGUGCAGAUGGAAUGACCAACACAUUUCGUCCUUAAGAGAGCAGUGGUUCCUCAGGUUCUGAGGAGAGGAAGGUGUCCAGGCAGCACCAUCUCUGUGCGAAUCCCCAGGGUAAAGGCGUGGGGCAUUGGGUUUGCUCCCCUUGCUGCUGCUCCAUCCCUGCAGGAGGCUCGCGCUGAGGCAGGACCGUGCGGCCAUGGCUGCUGCAUUCAUUGAGCACAAAGGUGCAGCUGCAGCAGCAGCUGGAGAGCAAGAGUCACCCAGCCUGUGCGCCAGAAUGCAGAGGCUCCUGACCUCACAGCCAGUCCCUGAUAGAACACACGCAGGAGCAGAGUCCCCUCCCCCUCCAGGCUGCCCUCUCAACUUCUCCCUCACCUCCUUCCCUAGGGGUAGACAGAGAUGUACCAAACCUUCCGGCUGGAAAGCCCAGUGGCCGGCGCCGAGGCUCGUGGCGUCACGCCCCCCCCGCCAGGGCUGUACCUCCGUCUCCCUGGUCCUGCUGCUCACAGGACAGACGGCUCGCUCCCCUCUUCCAGCAGCUGCUCUUACAGGCACUGAUGAUUUCGCUGGGAAGUGUGGCGGGCAGCUUUGCCUAAGCGUGGAUGGCUCCUCGGCAAUUCCAGCCUAAGUGAAGGCGCUCAGGAGCCUCCUGCUGGAACGCGACCCAUCUCUCCCAGGACCCCGGGGAUCUUAAGGUCAUUGAGAAAUACUGUUGGAUCAGGGUUUUGUUCUUCCACACUGUAGGUGACCCCUUGGAAUAACGGCCUCUCCUCUCGUGCACAUACCUACCGGUUUCCACAACUGGAUUUCUACAGAUCAUUCAGCUGGUUAUAAGGGUUUUGUUUAAACUGUCCGAGUUACUGAUGUCAUUUUGUUUUUGUUUUAUGUAGGUAGCUUUUAAGUAGAAAACACUAACAGUGUAGUGCCCAUCAUAGCAAAUGCUUCAGAAACACCUCAAUAAAAGAGAAAACUUGGCUUGUGUGAUGGUGCAGUCACUUUACUGGACCAACCCACCCACCUUGACUAUACCAAGGCAUCAUCUAUCCACAGUUCUAGCCUAACUUCAUGCUGAUUUCUCUGCCUCUUGAUUUUUCUCUGUGUGUUCCAAAUAAUCUUAAGCUGAGUUGUGGCAUUUUCCAUGCAACCUCCUUCUGCCAGCAGCUCACACUGCUUGAAGUCAUAUGAACCACUGAGGCACAUCAUGGAAUUGAUGUGAGCAUUAAGACGUUCUCCCACACAGCCCUUCCCUGAGGCAGCAGGAGCUGGUGUGUACUGGAGACACUGUUGAACUUGAUCAAGACCCAGACCACCCCAGGUCUCCUUCGUGGGAUGUCAUGACGUUUGACAUACCUUUGGAACGAGCCUCCUCCUUGGAAGAUGGAAGACCGUGUUCGUGGCCGACCUGGCCUCUCCUGGCCUGUUUCUUAAGAUGCGGAGUCACAUUUCAAUGGUACGAAAAGUGGCUUCGUAAAAUAGAAGAGCAGUCACUGUGGAACUACCAAAUGGCGAGAUGCUCGGUGCACAUUGGGGUGCUUUGGGAUAAAAGAUUUAUGAGCCAACUAUUCUCUGGCACCAGAUUCUAGGCCAGUUUGUUCCACUGAAGCUUUUCCCACAGCAGUCCACCUCUGCAGGCUGGCAGCCGAAUGGCUUGCCAGUGGCUCUGUGGCAAGAUCACACUGAGAUCGAUGGGUGAGAAGGCUAGGAUGCUUGUCUAGUGUUCUUAGCUGUCACGUUGGCUCCUUCCAGGGUGGCCAGACGGUGUUGGCCACUCCCUUCUAAAACACAGGCGCCCUCCUGGUGACAGUGACCCGCCGUGGUAUGCCUUGGCCCAUUCCAGCAGUCCCAGUUAUGCAUUUCAAGUUUGGGGUUUGUUCUUUUCGUUAAUGUUCCUCUGUGUUGUCAGCUGUCUUCAUUUCCUGGGCUAAGCAGCAUUGGGAGAUGUGGACCAGAGAUCCACUCCUUAAGAACCAGUGGCGAAAGACACUUUCUUUCUUCACUCUGAAGUAGCUGGUGGUACAAAUGAGAACUUCAAGAGAGGAUGUUAUUUAGACUGAACCUCUGUUGCCAGAGAUGCUGAAGAUACAGACCUUGGACAGGUCAGAGGGUUUCAUUUUUGGCCUUCAUCUUAGAUGACUGGUUGCGUCAUUUGGAGAAGUGAGUGCUCCUUGAUGGUGGAAUGACCGGGUGGUGGGUACAGAACCAUUGUCACAGGGAUCCUGGCACAGAGAAGAGUUACGAGCAGCAGGGUGCAGGGCUUGGAAGGAAUGUGGGCAAGGUUUUGAACUUGAUUGUUCUUGAAGCUAUCAGACCACAUCGAGGCUCAGCAGUCAUCCGUGGGCAUUUGGUUUCAACAAAGAAACCUAACAUCCUACUCUGGAAACUGAUCUCGGAGUUAAGGCGAAUUGUUCAAGAACACAAACUACAUCGCACUCGUCAGUUGUCAGUUCUGGGGCAUGACUUUAGCGUUUUGUUUCUGCGAGAACAUAACGAUCACUCAUUUUUAUGUCCCACGUGUGUGUGUCCGCAUCUUUCUGGUCAACAUUGUUUUAACUAGUCACUCAUUAGCGUUUUCAAUAGGGCUCUUAAGUCCAGUAGAUUACGGGUAGUCAGUUGACGAAGAUCUGGUUUACAAGAACUAAUUAAAUGUUUCAUUGCAUUUUUGUAAGAACAGAAUAAUUUUAUAAAAUGUUUGUAGUUUAUAAUUGCCGAAAAUAAUUUAAAGACACUUUUUUUUUCUCUGUGUGUGCAAAUGUGUGUUUGUGAUCCAUUUUUUUUUUUUUUUUUUAGGACACCUGUUUACUAGCUAGCUUUACAAUAUGCCAAAAAAGGAUUUCUCCCUGACCCCAUCCGUGGUUCACCCUCUUUUCCCCCCAUGCUUUUUGCCCUAGUUUAUAACAAAGGAAUGAUGAUGAUUUAAAAAGUAGUUCUGUAUCUUCAGUAUCUUGGUCUUCCAGAACCCUCUGGUUGGGAAGGGGAUCAUUUUUUACUGGUCAUUUCCCUUUGGAGUGUAGCUACUUUAACAGAUGGAAAGAACCUCAUUGGCCAUGGAAACAGCCGAGGUGUUGGAGCCCAGCAGUGCAUGGCACCGUUCGGCAUCUGGCUUGAUUGGUCUGGCUGCCGUCAUUGUCAGCACAGUGCCAUGGACAUGGGAAGACUUGACUGCACAGCCAAUGGUUUUCAUGAUGAUUACAGCAUACACAGUGAUCACAUAAACGAUGACAGCUAUGGGGCACACAGGCCAUUUGCUUACAUGCCUCGUAUCAUGACUGAUUACUGCUUUGUUAGAACACAGAAGAGACCCUAUUUUAUUUAAGGCAGAACCCCGAAGAUACGUAUUUCCAAUACAGAAAAGAAUUUUUAAUAAAAACUAUAACAUACACAAAAAUUGGUUUUAAAGUUGACUCCACUUCCUCUAACUCCAGUGGAUUGUUGGCCAUGUCUCCCCAACUCCACAAUAUCUCUAUCAUGGGAAACACCUGGGGUUUUUGCGCUACAUAGGAGAAAGAUCUGGAAACUAUUUGGGUUUUGUUUUCAACUUUUCAUUUGGAUGUUUGGCGUUGCACACACACAUCCACCGGUGGAAGAGACGCCCGGUGAAAACACCUGUCUGCUUUCUAAGCCAGUGAGGUUGAGGUGAGAGGUUUGCCAGAGUUUGUCUACCUCUGGGUAUCCCUUUGUCUGGGAUAAAAAAAAUCAAACCAGAAGGCGGGAUGGAAUGGAUGCACCGCAAAUAAUGCAUUUUCUGAGUUUUCUUGUUAAAAAAAAAUUUUUUUAAGUAAGAAAAAAAAAGGUAAUAACAUGGCCAAUUUGUUACAUAAAAUGACUUUCUGUGUAUAAAUUAUUCCUAAAAAAUCCUGUUUAUAUAAAAAAUCAGUAGAUGAAAAAAAUUUCAAAAUGUUUUUGUAUAUUCUGUUGUAAGAAUUUAUUCCUGUUAUUGCGAUAUACUCUGGAUUCUUUACAUAAUGGAAAAAAGAAACUGUCUAUUUUGAAUGGCUGAAGCUAAGGCAACGUUAGUUUCUCUUACUCUGCUUUUUUCUAGUAAAGUACUACAUGGUUUAAGUUAAAUAAAAUAAUUCUGUAUGCA